ACUUACAAUUACGAGAUUUAUAUUUGCAUUAGUCUCUUUGGCUGGUGGGUAGGGGUGAGAGGCUCUUCCUGGAUCCCUUAUUUUCUACAGGAGAGGAGGAAAACACCUGGGAUGCUCCAGUGCUCUUACGCAGAUAAUGAUCAUUAACAUCAGCCUCUCUGAUCAAAGAGCUACUCCACCCCACUCUGGCUGUAGUGUGACAUUCCUGCCUGCCUGAGGAAGAAAUGGUGAGCAGGGGCUGCAAUUGCAGACAAGUGUCACCCAGAAGCCACAAGUUUCUGUGAGCACCAGGUCUACAAACUACCCAAGGCAUAGCAAUGGCAUUAUCACUGGAAGAAUUCGUCCACUCCCUUGACCUCAGGACCCUACCCAGGGUUCUAGAAAUCCAGGCAGGCAUCUAUCUUGAAGGCUCUAUUUAUGAAAUGUUUGGAAAUGAAUGCUGUUUUUCAACAGGAGAAGUGAUUAAAAUUACUGGUCUCAAAGUUAAGAAGAUCAUAGCUGAAAUUUGUGAGCAGAUUGAAGGUUGUGAGUCUCUACAGCCAUUUGAACUGCCUAUGAAUUUUCCAGGGACUUUUGUUAAAAGAAGCAAGGAAUGUCUUUUUAAGAUUGUGGCUGAUAAAACUCCAUACCUUACUAUGGAAGAAAUCACAAGGACCAUUCAUAUUGGACCAAGUAGACUAGGGCAUCCUUGCUUCUAUCAUCAGAAGGAUAUAAAACUAGAGAACCUCAUCAUAAAGCAGGGUGAGCAAAUCAUGCUCAACUCAGUUGAAGAGAUUGAUGGAGAAAUAAUGGUGAGCUGUGCAGUAGCAAGGAAUCAUCAAACUCACUCAUUUAAUUUGCCUUUGUCACAAGAAGGAGAAUUCUACGAGUGUGAAGAUGAACGUAUUUACACUCUAAAGGAGAUUGUUGAAUGGAAGAUUCCUAAGAACAGAACAAGAACUGUAAACCUUACAGAUUUUUCAAAUAAGUGGGACUCAACGAAUCCAUUUCCUAAAGACUUUUAUGGUACCCUGAUUCUCAAGCCUGUUUAUGAAAUUCAAGGUGUGAUGAAAUUUCGAAAAGAUAUAAUCCGCAUCCUCCCCAGUCUAGAUGUCGAAGUCAAAGACAUCACUGAUUCUUACGAUGCUAACUGGUUUCUUCAGCUGUUAUCAACAGAAGAUCUUUUUGAAAUGACUAGUAAAGAGUUCCCCAUAGUGACUGAAGUCAUAGAAGCACCUGAAGGAAACCACCUGCCCCAAAGCAUUUUACAGCCUGGGAAAACCAUUGUGAUCCACAAAAAGUACCAGGCAUCAAGAAUCUUAGCUUCAGAAAUUAGAAGCAAUUUUCCUAAAAGACACUUCUUGAUCCCCACUAGCUAUAAAGGCAAGUUCAAGCGGCGACCGAGGGAGUUCCCAACGGCCUAUGACCUAGAGAUCGCUAAGAGUGAAAAGGAGCCUCUUCACGUGGUGGCCACCAAAGCGUUUCAUUCCCCUCAUGACAAGCUGUCAUCCGUAUCUGUUGGGGACCAGUUUCUGGUGCAUCAGUCAGAGACGACUGAAGUCCUCUGUGAGGGAAUAAAAAAAGUGGUGAAUGUUCUGGCCUGUGAAAAAAUCCUCAAAAAGUCCUAUGAGGCUGCGCUGCUCCCUUUGUACAUGGAAGGAGGUUUUGUAGAGGUGAUUCAUGAUAAGAAACAGUACCCGAUUUCUGAGCUCUGUAAACAGUUCCGUUUGCCCUUCAAUGUGAAGGUGUCUGUCAGGGAUCUUUCCAUUGAAGAGGACGUGUUGGCUGCCACACCAGGACUGCAGUUGGAGGAGGACAUUACAGACUCUUACCUACUCAUAAGUGACUUUGCCAACCCCACGGAGUGCUGGGAAAUUCCUGUGGGCCGCUUGAAUAUGACUGUUCAGUUAGUUAGUAAUUUCUCUAGGGAUGCAGAACCAUUUCUAGUCAGGACUCUGGUAGAAGAGAUCACUGAAGAGCAAUAUUACAUGAUGCGGAGAUAUGAAAGCUCAGCCUCACAUCCCCCACCUCGCCCUCCGAAACACCCCUCAGUAGAGGAAACAAAGUUAACCCUGCUAACCUUAGCAGAAGAAAGGACGGUAGACCUGCCCAAGUCUCCCAAGGCUGGAGUGCAAUGGCGUGAUCUUGGCUCGCUGCAACCUCUGCCUCCCGGGUUCAAGCAAUUCUCUGCCUCAGCCUCCCACGUAGCUGGGAUUACAGGCACCCCCCACCACGUCCAGGUAAUUUUUGUAUUUUUAGUAGAGAUGGGGUUUCACCAUCUUGGCCAGGCUGGUCUUGAACUCCUGACCUUGUGAUCCACCCACCUGGGCCUCCCAAAGUGCUGGGAUUACAGGCAUGAGCCACUGCACCUAGCCAAUGUUAGCAUUUUUUUGGUAGCUAUUUGAGCUUUCCUUAGAGUAAGACAUGUACAGAUUAAUAAAUCAUGGUUUUUGAGUUGCCAGAGGUCUGUUGUCUAGUAAAUGGCAUGGGCUAUAAACAGACAACUAAAGAAGUGAAAAAGACGGGAGAAGAGGGCAAAGGAUGAAUAAAGGAAGUGCUGGGUUGAAAGUUAGCCAAACUUGAGUUAUAGCUGAAACCUCGAAGGUACAAAUCUGUGCCCAAUGGCACAUACGGAAUAUUUACAAGCUCUUUUUGUGCUUCUGGAAUGGGAGAGGAGUGAUCUGAAUUUUAGUUUUGCUCUAGGCAUGACAUGUACUGUGUUGAUACUUCUAUCUGGAUAGCUGAGUUGGUAUAAUUGAGUUUUAAAUGAAAAGGAAUUGGUUAAACUAAAAUAUUCGCAAAUAUCACCUGAUUUUAGGGAAAUUUCAAGAAACAAUGAACAAGUCUUCAUACUAAUAAUAAAAUACUGAUUUUCUCUGGAUAAUUUAUGGCUAAAGAACAUGGUUUUCAUUAUGGCAUGAUUGAAGUACACUUUCAAUUGGAAAUAUGUGAAGAAACUAAAAUUUUGGCCCUCUCUGAACUUUUUAACAACUGAGAAUGUUCUCACCUGGGGGCAAUGAUGAAAAACAUUAGCUAAUACUGUCCCCCACUCCUUAUCUAUAGUGUCAAGAACAAAAAUACCACCAAAUAUGUGAUGUCAUAUUUUCGGUGUUACUGAGUAUUACUUUUUUAGCAGAAAAAAAUGUGAAUUUAUAAAAUUUAUUUAUUUUCUCAAUAGAUUAGCAAAAAGCUUGAGCAAAUUUGGACUAAAUUAUUUUGCACUAGAUUUCUGGCCUUUAAGAAAAUUAGAAUAGUUUUCAUUUACUAAAAUGUCCACUACAUGGAAAUUCCUGUUUGAAAUGAUAGCAAUAACAGAAAAAUGAUCAGUUCAUUGCACAGUAUGUAUUAAGUGAGAGCAUUUGAAUUGCCAAUUUCCUAUAAUCUCUAUAGAAAUUUUAGUGCCUGUAAUCACUAAAAUUGAGUGUGGGCUCACUAGAUAUUUAUGUUCCUUUCCUUGAGCUUAUUACCUUCAGUUUUUCUUUAAAAAAAAAAAUCAAAAGAGCAGUUGAAGAAAAGUAGAGGAGAUAAGUUCCAGUUGGCUAUGCAGUUUUGAAACAGAUUUGUCUGAAUUUUCCAUUACUAUAUUUGUCAAUUGUGAAUUUAUUUUAGAAUAAAACCUUGCCUAAAAAUAAAUUGAUAACACAUAAGCUAUAUAUUUGAGCAAAUAAGUUUUGCUACAAUUCCCCAGUUCCUUGCAAGUUAACCAUUACUUUUAAUCUUCGGUGAUGUUUUCAUUGAUAUCAGACCUACAUCAAUAAAUAUAUUUAUGCUUUGCUUCCCAAACCAAAUUUUCCUGGAUAAAUAUUAGGACAGAAAAUGAGCACAAGAUGGCUAUGAAAGAAUGCAAUAAAAUAGGCUUCCAAAAAUCAGUAUUUUUUCCCAAACUUUGAAAAGUAAAAAACGUAAGAAGAAAAAGAUUUGUCUUAGAAAUAGAAGAGAGUAGAAAGUGAAAAUGAACUUUAAAUUUAAGAGACCGGAGGGCCCAUAAAUACUUUAAAAAUUCAUAGACAAAGAAAAGAUUCAUGCAUGCGUUAUUUAAGGAAAAACUCUCAGCAAACCUUUUAUAGCCGUAAACUUUCUCAUACACUUUGUCCAGAAUCUAACUUCAGUAUAAUCAUGAUGUCUUAGAAACUUUCUAAGCAAUACUUAAUUAAGAUACACUUCUAAUAGGACAAGUUGCUUUUAGCCUCUUUGUAAGAGGUUAAAAUAUCUCUAAUGCUCUCAUUUGAGAUAUUUACCAUUGGUCUCCUUUGAGAUAUUUACCACAAGCCAAUUACACAGACGAUUUUAGAUCUCAUGAGAACAAAAUAAGAGAGAAUUCUAUAAAAUCAGAAGGCUGUUGACUACAAAAUUAGACAAACAAGAAUCAAACUGUACAUUAAAGGCCACAAGAAAUGUAUAAUAAAUCCACUGUUAUUUAUGAAGGUGCACACAAAAUUAAAAAGGCUGAUUAUAAAAUUAUGAAGUCACACAAUAUAUAAAAGGAAUAAAUAUUUGUUUUUUUUAGUGUAACUGAAAAGAUACCAAUAUUAUUCUGACUUGUGACAUUACGCUCAUUCAGAUCACUAAACUUUACAUACCAUUUGUCCUUAAUAAAAGUUUGUUGUUGUUAUCAAAUGCUUUUAAAAGUUGUAAUUAAUGUCUUAAAAGUAUGCAAUUACCAGUUGUGAAAUAGGAUAAAACACAAAGUCAUGUAAGACGUGUUUUCUCAAUUGUUAUCCAAGGCUGAGAACCACCCUAUCCAAGCUAUUCUCUUCAUUGGUUCUGAUUUCAGCUUUUCUCCUGAGGUAAAAUCAUUUCUGUAUUUUCCAUUCAUACUAGACUCUGCUUCAACCAAAUUCUCACAAUGUUGUCAGACAUCUUGUGUUCAAUAAUAAAAUAUCCAAAGGUCUAUGAUCCAGACUGAUCUCAAUCUUUUGUAAUAAAAACACCAGCUGCUCAUUACUGAGCUGGCGCUAUACCAGGUGCUUACAUGUAUUAAUCUCUUAUUUAAUCUUCCACAUUGCUCCAUGAGAUGGAUGCUGUGAUCAUCUCUAUUUUGCAGAUAAGGUAAUUUAGGCUAAGGGGUAUAUAAGGUGUGUCAUGGUUACCAAUGAUACUCAGGUUGCCAGAUUUUAUGGUCAAUCCUCAGUCCUCAUAUUAUUUGAAUACUAGGUACUAUUUGGCACAGUUAAACACUACCUACUUUUUAAAAUCCUUUCUUAGAAUUCUGCAAUAUUAUGCCUUCCUGAUUUCUUUAUACUGUAGUGGUUGUAUUUUUCUCUCAUCUUUUUUGGUAGCUCUUCUCUGAUCUCCCUUAACUCUUAAUGUUCAAGUGCCUUUGAGCUCAGUCUUUGGUCUCUUUUCUAUAUAUGUCUACUUUUAAAAUUCCUAUCCACACACACAAAUUUCUUAUUUUAUGCAUAUAAAAUGGCUGUCAGUAGAAUUAUUCAUGUAUAUGGAUUCAUAAAGGAAAGCAACCAGAAAUGGUGUCAUAUUUUUCUGUUAAAAUCUGCUUAAAUAUGUGUAAAUGUCAUUUUUUAAGGAGAGUUCAGCUCCUGGGAGAUGCUAGCUGUAUCACUAUGUCUGUUCUGUAGCAGUUACAGUUUUCAACUAUACCUCUGGAAGAGAUUGAAGGUCAGGGAAAGUGAUCAGGUAAGGAAAGAGCCUUCCUACCGACAUGCUAUUCUGAUGAAUGUAGGCUUAUCAUGCUUAGGACUUUUCUUUCCUGAUCCACUGAUGUGAAGAAAGUUGAGAAUAUCUUGAACUCUCUAUGAGACAUUACAACUUUAGCUGAUGAACUUUGGCAUCAGCAAAAACUCUUUAGUAACAAUUCAGGAUUUAGCUGAAAUAAGUUUCAGGAAGUAGAACUAAGAAUAGGAGUAGAACUUAGGACUAUUAAUUUGAAUACCAUAUUGAGUAGGUGAUAAUAUAAGAUCCAGAGAGAAUAUGAAGUCUUCUCUUCAUUAAGGUAGAUAGGGAUGUAUAACAGGAAAAGAUUAAUAAAGGGUUAAUGUGUUCAGGAGCACAGAAUAAUGAACACUUUAAUAAUAAGCAAAGAAAAAUUUAGAAAAAAAAGAAAGCAGAUCAGUGUUUUCCUAGAGAGAUAAGUAGGCAUAACACUGCCUACUCAAUGACAAAUGACAAGAGGAACAUUUUCGGGUGAUGAAAAGGUUCUAAAACUGGAUUAUGAUAAUGGUUGCACAGAUCUAUAAAUGUAUUAAAAUCAUAGCGCUGUACACUUAAAAUCAUCAAUCAUACCUGAAUACAGCCAUUAAAAUAUUCUAAUUAUAGCAUAGAUAAUCAAUUCAAACAGAGGCAGGGAGACCAGUUAGGAAGCUAAAACAAUAAUAUAAGAGAGAGGAUGCCUGCCUCUGUGAAUGGAAGACACAUAUUCAAGAGAAUUUUAGCAUAUGGUAGGUGUAGGAUGUAUGGUUGAUAAAUUGUAGAAAAUAAGAAAGGUACAAGAUAAGGAAAGUAUCCAGAUUUCUAACAUAAGCAUCAGAAUGGAUGGUGGUGAAAUUGAUUAAAACACAUUCAGAAAAUUCAUUAAAAUAAAAAACACAGAACAUAGGUAGAAGAAUAGCACAUUAUUCAGGGUUCUCCACAGGGACAGAACAUUUCCCUUUCCACAAUGCACAGUUACCCUGGUAAAAGGCUAGAGGUCUCCUUGGGGAAGGAUGGGAGAAAGAUUCACUGCAUGAAUUGUCGGUAAUGUAGUGGGGUCCUUCCACAAGGAGUCCUGGCCUCCCCUUCAUUCAAGGGGUUCUGGGUCUGUAAACUGGCUCAAGUCUGGAAAUUGAUUGAAGGGCCAUGAUUCUCUAUUUUUUAUAACUCAAAUUAGUCUUUUGCCCAUUCGACCUAGAAGUUUUCUGUUUGUAUAAUUUAAGUAGGAAUGCAGUAGGCUUCCUAUCAAAUUCACUUCUAGGAACACUGUGAUUAAUUAGCCAAUGCCAGAGCUCUACACACAUCAGAUUAUUCUGAUUGCCUCUUUGCCUCUGCUGUCCAUUAUGGUAGCUACGCCCACCUUUGCUUUGAUGUUCAGUGCUGCCACUUGGCCCCUGCCACCUCAGGAUCCAAUUAUUCCUACUACAUUUAAAUUUUGUAGUUGAGUGACAGUGGUUCCCUCGUUAGAUCUGACAUACAGAAAAGCGCAAUUACAGGGCUCUUCAGAGAUGCAGGUGCUGCCCUCAUAAAUCUAUUUUGCAAGGCAUUGGUCAAGGGUAUAUCUUCUGGACCCUCCCAGCUGGGAUGAGUAGGUCUAAAGUGACUAAUCCACUCCACCAUCCCAAUCUCCCUAAGCCUUUGGAUCUUUUCCUUUACAUUAAACCAAGGAAGAUCAGGCAUUUCCAACUUGCUCACAGUGGGCCAUCUUUUAAUCUAUAUUUCACCUAACCAAGCAAAUAAACUCUUAGAACCUUUUUUAACUCCCCGAACUGCAACAUUAAAUGCAGAGUUCCUACUUAGUGGGCCCAAAUCAACAAAUUCAGGGUGAUCCAACUGUAUGUUCCUUCCACCAUUAUCCCACACCCUUAAUAUCCAUUCCCAUGCCUGUUCUCCAGAUUUCUCUUUAUAUAAAUUAGAGAACUCAAGCAGUUCUUUUCCCGUGUAGUGCAUCUCCUCAUGGGUCACACUCUCAACCUCACCUCUAGCGCCCCACCAGGACUUUUGUCUAGUUGUAGGUCUAGAAGCACACAGGGGUGUUGGGGGUGGCUCCUGAGCAGAAUCAACAUUAUCUUGCCUGGCAACCGCCUCAGGGGAGGCCAUCACCGUUGCCUCAGGCAGCGCAGGGUUUAUCUCCUCAGACAAAGGUGGAAAGGCUGAUGGCAGCAUGGGUUGAGGAGGGGAUGUUGUCACUACUGGGGAUGGGGAAGCUGUUUCUUCUGGCAAAAAAGCAAAAAAGGUUCAUGAGAGUUUCGAAACUCAGUGUCUCCAGCUUCUUCAGGGUCCUCCCACUCGUCCUCAUUCCAAGUUGCAGGGUCCCAUUCUUUUCCAGUCAAUACCCUCACUUUAACAGUAGACACCUGGCAAGGGUGUGCAUGUACCUUUUGUUGCAGGUCAGCCACUCACAUGAUAAGAGCUUGUGUCUAUUUUUCCACAAUUUCAGCUCUUUCUGUACAGGAGACUCAGGGCAAUCUUAGCAGAUCUGAGGCUUGAUAUCUGCUUCUGAAGCCAGGAGAUAGAAUCCUCGAUUUCAUUCAUCACUUUGCCCACUGAACUUAGGAGCAACCAAGGAGCUUCAUUAUAUUCUCUACGUAUGGUCAAAGGUUCCUUGGUUCUCCACAUAUGGUCAAAGGUAUUAUGUAUAGAGUCACUAAACUCCUUGCCUCUCAUGAGCAUGUAUCAGGAAUGUCAAAUGCAUUUAUUUUGCAUAACUCUCUAAACAGUUCAUGCCAAGGACUCAGUGUUCUCCACACUAUUAGAAGUAGAGUCCUUAGCAUUUUUUGAUCUAAUCAUAUUAUGCAGCCAACUCCAGAAACCCCAAAACCAACGAAAGAACUUCAUCCUUAAUAUUCUGUUCCUCUUCCUCUAGAACCACUCCUGUUACCAAAAUCUAUAUUAGUCAGGGUUCUCUACAGGGACAGAACUAAUGGAAUAUAGGUCCCACAAUAGGCCAUCUUCAGGCUGAGGAGCAAGGAGAGCCAGUCCAAUUCCAAAACUGAAGAACUUGGAGUCCGAUGUUCAAGGGCAGGAAGCAUCCAGCACAGGAGAAAGAUGUAGGCUGGGAAGCUAGGUCAGUCUCCCCUUUCCCAUUUUUCUGCCUCCUUAUAUUCUGCUGCACUCUAAGCUGAUUUGAUUGUGUCCACUCAGAUUAAGGGUGGGUCUGCCUUUCCCAGCCCACUGACUCAAACGUUAACCUCCUUUGGCAACACCCUCACAGACACACCCAGAAUGAAUACUUUGUGUCCUUCAAUCCAAUCAAGUUAACACUCAGUAUUAACCAACGCAGAUGGUUUUACAGAAGCAAGGUUACAGUUUAGUUUGGUUUGAAAUUUCUGAGUUGAGAUGCCUAGUAUGAUGUUUACCAUGGGUCUGUACUUUAGGAAAGAAAUCUAAGCUAGGGAUGAUGAUUCAAGUGUCAACAAAUAUGUGAUAAAUAAUGUCCUUUGAGAAGGUGAGAUGAAGCUAGAGUGGGUAGCCCAUGAGAGAAGAAGAUGGAAUUUUUUUUCUGAGGAAGUCCAAAAUAUAAGGAACAAAGGAAAUAUAUUAAAAAAUCUAAAAUAUAAGAACCAGAGGGCUUUAUUAGCUGAGUGCCAACAAUGAAUCAGUCACUAUUCUGUUUUCUACAUGCAUCAACUCAUUUAGUCCUCAUACAAAACUAGUGAAAUUAAUUCCCUAAUUAUUAUUAUCCCAAUUUUACAGAUGAGAAAAAGCUCAUCAACAAUGGAUAACUUUCCAAGACCACAUGUAUGGAUUAUUGCUUUUCAGGUAUAAAUAAUGAACAACAUUUUAAGGGACUCAGUACUAUGAAGAACGUUUGUGAUUUUAGAAUCAAAAUUCAAGCCAUGGCUAAUUGAUGCUUUUUUCCCCUAAUAAAAAUUGUGAACAUCAUUAUGACUAAAUUGGUCACUUAUAACUUGUCAAGGAAAAAUUUUCUGAAAUACAUCAUCCUCAAUUGGCUCCUUCUUCGGGAAUAUGACUUGUUAUCAUGGUAUGGGUAAAGGAUGGUAGAGAAUCAAGAACUACAAAUAAUGUACAAAUGUGAGAUCUCUAUCUCUAUCAAUUGCACUUAUUUAAUUGGCCAGAGAAAAUCAUAGUCCGUGUGUAUGUUCGAGUGUGAAAGUGUAACCUUCCCUUAAGCCUGAAAGUAGAGGGAAACUGGGUACUAGUGAACAAUAUAAGAACUAUUACAUGGUCCAGAAAGAAAAGAAAGAAGGAAAGAAAGAAAAAAAGAAAGAAAGAAAGAAAGAAAGAAAGAAAGAUAGAAAGAAAGAAAGAAAGAAAGAGAAAGAAAGAAAGAAAGAUUACCAAUGGGGUUCUCAUUUCUUAUCUUUGCAAAUGCCACCACCAUCUACUGACUUGCCUAAACCAAAUAUGUAGGAACAGUCCUUCCUUUUUUAUUCCUGUUUGCAUUUGUCAAUCAUCAAAUCCUGUAGAUUCUAUUUCUUUGACAUCUCUUGAAUAUAUAUACUUCCUUACUUCAGGUCUUCAUCAUUUCUUGUCUGGAUUAUUGAGACCAUCUCUUAACUAGUCUUUUUGUUUUUGAUCACCACACUUAAAUUUAUUAUCCACAUUACUGACAAUUUGAUAAUUCUAAAAAGAAAAUCUUACCAUGUAUCUCUCUUGCUGAGAACGUGUUGUGGCUUUCUUUUCAAUAGUUUAUCGCCUGUCCAUUAUUUAUUUCUCAAGCCUUUCUACCUUCAUACCUUGCCUCACGUUUAUACAUUUAGUAUUUGGCUAUAUUAAAUUUUUGCAGCCUGCAAAUACUUUAUUCUCUUCUGAGUCUUUAAUUUUUCUUUUUUCUUUCUUUUUUUUUUUUUUUUUGAGACGGAGUCUCGCUCUGUCGCCCAGGCUGGACUGCAGUGGCACAAUCUCAGCUCACUGCAAGCUCCGCCUCCCGGGUUCACGCCAUUCUCCUGCCUCAGCCUCCCGAGUAGCUGGGACUACAGGCGCCCGCCACCACGCCCAGCUAAUUUUUUGUAUUUUUUUAGUAGAGACAGGGUUUCACCGUUUUAGCCAGGAUGGUCUCGAUCUCCUGACCUCGUGAUCCGCCCGCCUCGGCCUCCCAAAGUGCUGGGAUUACAGGCGUGAGCCACCGCGCCCGGCCGUCUUUAAUUUUUCAAUUGGAAUUUUGUUACUUUUUUAAACAACCAUUUAUUGGGGGCUCACUAACAUUUAAGUAACUAAAUAGUUCUCAUUCAAUUCUUUCCAUAUCCCUAUGAGUGUUAUUAAUAUUCCCAAGACAUGAACACUGAAGCUCAGAGAAUAAUUAUGAAUCUUAUUUUAAAUGUGUGAUCAUAGUUCAUGAAAGAUCUGAAGAAAGAGAACUACUACUCAGAGUGUAAGCUAGAAUUCGAAACCAUCCUUUAUUUAGACCAGCGUGGCACAUGUAUACAUAUGUAACUAACCUGCACAAUGUGCACAUGUACCCUAAAACUUAAAGUAUAAUAAUAAAAGAAAAAAAAAAUUCUGUUUCUUAACUACUUAGUCAUUUUCAGUGAUCUUUUAUUUUUUUGAACUAAUAUCACAACUUUAAAAUAAGAUCCACUGUUAUGUGUUUGCAUAUAAAUAUACACUUGUGGUUUUAAGAGUAAGGCACGCUAUUUUAGAAAAGAGAAAAAUGAAAGAGGAAAAUAAAAUCAGGAGCACUUUCAUCAUAUUAAUAUUUUGUACUGUCAAUAUUAUAUUUCCGUUAUUCAUACACAUAUAGACUCAGACACACAUACGUGCAUGAUUCUGUAUUCAUCUGUGUCUGUGAUAAAGUGACGUAUGAACACAUAUGCGUAUGUACACAUGUGUGUAGUCUAACAGAUUGUUUCACUGACUCUUCAUCCUGGGAACCCAAAGCAUGAGAAACCAAAGCCUGAGAACAAAAUGCCUGUGAACCCCCACAUUUUAAAGUGAGCUGCAGAACUGUGUAUGCAGGACUUGGAAGGUGAAGGUCCUAUAAUUGAUGCCAGCAGUAUUAGCUAGUCUCCCAUCUUGGAAGCAAGGAGCAAGUGUUCUUUAAGUGCUUUUCUUUCACCUCAGAUAAAUUAGAGAAACAUUGAGAAGUUAGCAAAAUAAAGAGAGAAGAUUGUUUUACAGAUGGUUGUUAACCAUAUCCUGUGAAUUUUUAGUCCCUGGCAUUAUGGGUAAGAGAUGUUGGGUUCUUCUCCCUCACUUCAAGUUAUGUGAUGGGAUCUUCAGGUGAUCCAUUUGGAGGUCUUGCCAAUGAGCUGUAGGAGUUGGAAGAAAAUAGGAGCUGGCCUUUGACCCAUAUCUGCAAAAUCUAAAGGUAAGAGGCUGUGACUAGAGCUUCCCUUUGCCUGGGGUAAGUUAUUUUGAAAGAAAACUGCACUUAUGUCAAUAGCAGAAUGAAGGUGUGGGUUCUCUGAAGACAAGGUGUGAACUUGAGAGAUUGAAAGGGACCUUGACUAGUGCAUAUAUUUCCUGGAGUAGAAGCACUGAGGGUGGUAGUGGUACAUUCUUAGCCUUAGUCAAAGAAACUUGUGUGGUUCUCAAUGGGAUGGUUUCCCAUUAGUCUGAAGAAGUGACCUAUGAAAAAAAGGGUUAGUUUUUGACUCCUGCCAUUUCAACAUUAUAAAGAUAUUAGUGAUUCAAGAGUGUAUAUCCUUUCUUCUUAUUCCACUUUCUCCCAAGGCCCUAAGCUGGAGAAGUCAAAAAAGAAAGGUUAGUGCACGGAUGCAGGAGUUGAAGAGAGCACAUCAUUAAGCAGCCAAACAUACUUGCUUCUCUUCUGUAGACUUAAAAAACUCAAGUGGGAUUAAGCUACAGCAGGAAGAAGCCUUGACUUAGAGAAGGAUUCUGAGCUUUGUUAGUAUGCUAAACUGAGCUGGAGUCAAGUGGAUUUUUAUGAACCAUGUACUCACUAAAGACUAUGGGAUUUCCCCAUGAUUUUAUGCAGAGUUAGAAUAACCACUAGUUCACAGAGAUUUGAAGGGAUAUAAAACAGUGAGAAUCAAGGUGGCUCUUGUGUAGACACUAUAAAGUUCAGCUUACUCAAUAAAUUGCUGAUGAGUAUGCAUGUAUAUGUGUUCUGCAUACCAAACAUGGGUAUAUACUGUAUAUACCCAUGUAUUUAUGUGUGCGUGUCUAUACAUAUUAGUGUUUCUGUGUACGUAUGUGCAAUGCAAUUAUCUCCAGUCAUUCUUUGAAUGUCAAAUUUUGCUUUAAUAUCUAAGUAAAAUCAAAUAAGCUCUCAAUUUCAUAUAGUUUUGGCAAUGCUUCCUCCAUUAUUUCCAAAAAGUUAUGUGGGAUCUUUAUGUUUUCUCCUUUUGUCUCCUUUGCUUUCUUGCUCAUCACUCUUCUUUAGUUUUCAAUCACCUUGGAUCACUUCAAUACAGGCAUUCCGACUGCAUAAGGUUGAUCUGGUCUUUAGUGCCUCAAGCUAUCAAUUAAAUUUGUCCUUUUUUAUUUUUUAAGGAACCACUAAAAACGCACUUGUAGGUGAACAUAAAUUUGCUGAAGGUUUGGUGAUAAUGGCUAGGAACAGGAAGUAAAAGUUCUAAUCCCUAAUUUCUGAUGGCCCUUAACUCUAAACCUUAACCCACUUCAAGGUUUUUCAUCUCACAAAAUCAAUGCUUUUCUACCCAGGAUCAACCCACAUUAGUUUUUUGCUUAAUAAUGAUCAUAAUAAUAAUAAAUCAAAUGCAUUAAAAUGCUCAUUCUCAUAUUUAGUUCUAUACUUUUAAUCUUAGAAAGGUUAACUUGCCUUGAAAUCAGAUCCACUAUAAUGUAUUCUAAAUUUUUAUUUUCUUAUUUAACUUUUUAAUCUGUGAAAAAAUUUAUUUUGCAUAUAGUAUGGAGUGAGGAUCAAACUAUUUUCACAAAUGGUUAGUGUAUUUCCCCAGUACCACAUAUUGACUAAACAAUCCUUUACCUGUCUUUUCUGGAAGCAGUUUCUCAACUUUUUACUCUGUGUCUUUGAUUUACCUAAUUGUCUUAAACCAGUAUCAGUUACUUACAAUGUAGGACUUUCUAGUACUUCCUAAUAUGGAUAUGUAUUAGGUUGGCGCAAAAGCAAUUUCAGUGUCAAGAACUGCAAUUACUUUUGCACCAACUUAAUUUUUUUCUUCUUCUUCUUAGUAUUAAUCUUUUUCUUAUCAGUAAUUACUUAGAUUCUCAGCUUCCUGUACUUUCAAAUGAGCCUGUAAAACACUUUAUUAACUUCUAAAAAAAGUCUGGUGGCCGGGCGCGGUGGCUCACGCCUGUAAUCCCAGCACUUUGGGAGGCCGAGGCGGGCAGAUCACGAGGUCAGGAGAUCGAGACCGUCCUGGCUAACAAGGUGAAACCCCAUCUUUACUAAAAAUACAAAAAAUUAGCCGGGUGUGGUGGCAGGCACCUGUAGUCUCAGCGACUCAGGAGGCUGAGGCAGGAGAAUGGCAUGAACCCAUGAGGCAGAGCUUGCAGUGAGCCGAGAUCGUGCCACUGCACUCCAGCCUGGGUGACAGAGCAAGACUCCAUCUCAAAAAAUAAUAAUAAUAAUAAUACAAAUCUGGUGAGAUUUUUGAUUGCAAUUAUAUUAAGCAUAUUAAUUUGGGAGAAUUUGAAUUUUUAUGAUACUUGGUUUUCCGAUCUUGGCAAAUGGUUUUCUAUUCUAUUUAGCUAAAUCUUCUCAUGAAAGCCAUGUGUAUGUUUCUAACAAUUUCUGGUGUACUUCUGACAUAUCUAUAAACUCGUGGGAGAUAUCAGGUCAUCUCCUUGAGCAUUAGGAACUUUCAAUGCUAUGGAACUGUCUAUGGUACAGAAUUUAUAUUCUCACAUCUGAAUAAAACCAAAGAUUAUGUAUUUUAACAUGAUGAACAUCUGCUUUCCGUCAAGUCUUUCUUUCUGCAAAUAUCUGUUGGUUAUUAUAUUUUACAUACUGUUUUUUUGUGUUACAUUUUCAUCAGUAAUAAAACACCUCCGUAAAUGGUCUGAUACUCCUCUUAAUGUUUACUUUGUCUUGGAAGUAAAUGAUACAGCUAAAUGAUCAGGUAAAUGUUAGAGCAUUAAGAGUGCUAUAAAAAUAGAGCAAGAGGUAAGGACUAAGAGUUUAAGGGGUGUAGAAUAAUUUUUGAAAGAAUAUCAAGGUGUACCUUACUGAGAAGAUGACAUUUGUACAAAGACAUGAAUUGGUAAGAUGAGAUGUGCAUAGUGAGAGGAAAUGUUCCAGACAGAGGAAAGAGAUAAUAAACACAUUAAGGCAGGACUGUGUCUAAUGUGUUCAAGACAGGCAGAGACAGGCAUAGUGGCACAGUCCCAGCUACUCAGGGUGCUGAAGUAGAAGACCAGCAUGGACAACAUACUAAGACCCUGUAUUAAAUAAAAAUGAUUCAACCAGCAGGUCAGAAGGCUGAAAUAUUGCGACUGAAACUGAUAAAAGGAGAUGACAUCAGAGAGGAAAUUUGGGAAGCAGAUUGUGUAGGUCCUUGAGGUUGUUGUAGUAAUCUUGGCUUAAUUUUUCAUGAAAGAUGAAACAAUUAGAGAAUUGAGUGGAGAAAUGACAUAAACUGACUUACAUCUUAAAGGGCUCAUUUUGGCUUUUGUGUUGAGGUUAGACACUAGUGGAGCAAGAAUGGAAACAGAAAGUCCAGUUAGAAGAACAUUGCCGUCUUAAUAUUGCUAUGGGCUAGGAAGAUAGCAAUGGAGAUAAUAAGAAAUGGUUAAUUCUACAUCUGCUUUAAGUGCAAAGCCAAAAGUGUUUCUUUCUGGUUGCAUUUUCCCUCUUACUCUCAUUAAGUAAUCUUCAUUUUAUAACUUCUCCAAUUCUGACUUAAAAUUUAGCUUAUUUCUACCUGGGUUCUGUUAUUAACAGAAUGAUCUUCUUUUAGGCUUUAAAUACGAUGCUUUUUUGGGGGAAAAUGUUGAAAGUUUAAUCUGGAGUUAGAUAACUAUAGUGGGAAAGCCAACAACAACUUUAUCUGGAAAUUUGGAGAAUAUGGUUCUCGCCCUGGCUCUGUAAAUAGUUUGCUCUGUGGUCUGGGAUAAUCUUAGUGUCCUUGCUUAUAAAAUGAGGUUAGAGUAAAUGAUCAGUACUAUUUCUUCUAGUUAAAUAUUCUAUCAAUCUGUGAUUCUGUACUUAUGCACUGGCCAGUUAAGUGUUGAAUAAUACAUUUUAAACAAAAAAAUUCAGUUGAGUUCCUUGAAAUAUCUACAGGUUGCUUUGCUAUAGCUGAAAAAUUUUAAAGACAGGAAACAGGAAAGACCCCAAGUGAGCCUGCGGUAUUUUGAGGGAUGGUAGUCUUCUUGGUGCAUUCCCUGUUUCUUUGUCCUUGGCACCCAAAUAGAAGUCCUUGUCUGUAAUGCUUGAUUUCAUGGGGCCUGCUUUCUCUUCUUAAUCCUGCAUGUAGUAGAAACUUGGUUCCUGUUUUUAUCUUUUCUUACCUUCUCUGGGAGGAUUUUCCCAGGAACUGCCUCUGUUCAGAAUCACAACUCCUCCACUUCAGUCCUGCACUUCCAAAACCUGAUUUACUGUGGUUGUGUCAUUCUAUCAGAUAUGCACAUGGAGGUUCCCCACCAGCUUUUUAAUCCAUUUGAUCUUAAAGUUUUCCCUUAUUUGUCACUCUUGUUGAGAUUCCUCUUCAUGGCUGCCAAAUCCGUCCCAAUGUUUCCUCAACUGGGACCCAUUGUCUGCUUGUAGCUUGUCCCUGUUCUCUCCAGGAUCACACAAUGCUUUUGAUUCUGUGCAAUAGUGCAGACUAUUCCUUCCUGAAACUAACUCAAUUUGUUUUCGAACAAAUAUCACAAUAUUGUUUCCCUUAUUUCAAGGGGUUACAUUUGUGACUCUAUUUGCCGUUGAGAAAUGAGAAUUUAGAUGUUGAGAGGCUGUGGAAUGAAAGGUGGAAAUGGCUUGUUUUUGCAAAUGGAAAGAAAUCUACCCCCAUUUAGCUAAAAGCACAAGACUUUUCUAAUCAAGCAUUUGACAUCAUGACCAGGCUUGGGAAAAAGUGUACCUGUUCACUUAUAAUUGGUUCUGCUCACAGAAGUGCUUUCUCAUUGUCUGUGCAGCUACAGGAAAUAUGGUUAGUAAAAGCACAUCUCAGCCUGAUUGAAGCUGUUCUUUAAAGCUCUGCCAGACCAUGCUGCAAAACUGUUAUUUCCUAUUAUGAAAACUAAAUCUCGAAUCAUGGUUAAAAGGCAGUCUGUUUUGGGGAGAGUGGCCUGUAUAGGCAGGCAGUAAUUCAGAUUUGAUUGGCAACAUGAGUUUUUCAGGGAAUGGUUAAAAAUGAGGAGCAUUUUGAAGGCCAGAAACACAAUCCCAAAUGAUGAUUCUCAGAAUUUUCCUAACAUCAGGUUAUUGGUAAACCAUAUUACAAAAUUUUAAAAUCAUCUCUUUCCCAGAAACUAUAAUAAUAAAACAUAAUGGUUUUCUGUAUUUCUAUUUGACCCAUGUAACAGAACCCUGUGAGAUAGGUAUCAUUAUCACCAUUUUAUAGCUGAGAAAACUCACCCAAAGUUCCAAGGUUUACAGUGUCUUGGCCGUCCUGUCUCUCUGGUCUCUUGCCAACAGAACACGGGUACUUAUGGUCCCAUGAUGCCUGCUGUAAAAGCUAUUUAAGAGUAUCUUUUUCAACUUCACUGUGCUUUAUUUCCUUACGUGAAUACCAUGUUUACUGUUUCUAUCAUUGACAGAGCAAUACUGAUGGCAGCGGCGGCCCACCUUGAGUGGCCGCUGCAUGACACUGGCUACAAUGGGGGAGGCACAGCCAGGGCUGAGUGCUCCAUAGAACUGGUGGGAGCCGGGAACAGGUGGAAGCCAUGCCCCCUUCCAAGUUGGAGGAGCUGGAGCCCUGCCCUCCCAGGGGCAGCUGUGGCAGAGCAGCCAGCUGUGGACUCAGGCAUCACUGCACUCUCAGGGCCCCAGGAAACACCCUUGCCCCUUCAGGCUCAAAAGUGCCUGCUCUCGCUGCCUGACCUCUGCCCAUUCCCAGUGCCCACUCCAAUUUCAGAGCAAAGUUGUGGCCAAGCCUGGGGGCUGUCACGACUCGGCUGGGUGUGUGCACGCUUGGGGCAGCACUGAAACACCAGCCCCCUAUCACCUCAGCCUCCUCCAGAUUUUGGGUGCUCACAAACAUGGGAGGGAGGGUGAGGUGGGGGCUAAGGGUGGCUCAGCGCAGUCUUGCAGGCACCACUUGGCACAAAGAGCCAGGGCACCAUAGGCACCAUGGAGAGCAGGUUAAUGGUGGUAGGAUGCAAACAGGCUCCUGGGCAGAAAGGAGCAGAUCCCCAGUAAAGCCCCAUCUUCAGGCCAGGGACGGCCUGAAGCCUGCCGGAGGGCUGCCAUGGAGUGAGAACUUAAUGGAGCUUGCUCUGGGGCCUCCCAUGACUGCUCACGGGCCGAUCAGCACCUACUUUCUCCCCUCUUAAGCCCAUAAAAAUCUUGGACUCAGCCAGACUUGAGCAGAUGAUGGGAUGGCCUGCCUACAGAAAGGAACUACCCAUUGUGGGUCUCCUGUCUCCUGAGAGCUGAGUGGACAACGGGACAAUCAGCCUGCAGAAAGGAGCUACCCACUGUGGGUCUCCUUUCUGCUGACAGCUGAACAGAUAUUGGGAUGACCUGCCUAUGGAGAGGAGCUAACCACUGUGGGUCUCCUCUGAGCUGUUCUGUUGCUCAAUAAAGUACCUCUUCACCUUGCUCACCCUCUACUUGUCUGCAUAACUCAUUCUUCCUGGAUGCAGUACAAGAACUUGGGACCUGCCGAAUGGUGGGGCUGAAAGAGAUGUAACACAAACAGGGCUGAAAUACACCCCCUGCUUGCCACAUGGCAGGCAACAAGAAAAAGAUAAGAAAGAAGGAGAGAAGAGUUUCAGCCCUUCAGACAACCCAGACCUGGGAGCACCCUGAGCCAGGGCUGUGAUGCCCUUUUUGGGGUUCUGUGGUUCCUGGCAUCUCCAAGUUUCUGGGUGCCACCACAUUCCCUGGUGCCAGCCAUGGAAGCUACUUGCAGUGUGCCUCAUCCAGCCACAGCCUUGCAGGGAGCUGGUGCCUGGCACUGCCCACCCUGCUGCAGCCAGAGUGCCUGGCUGUGGGCAGUGGCUGGACCCCAUGCUUGCUCAUUCACACAAUCCUCACCGCUCUGUGCCUGGCUCACCCUUGGCAGGCAUGGGAUCCAGGUUUGUCACGCAAGCUGAGUUCAGGCUGCCAGGCCGAGUGGGCACAUCAAGCACAGUGGGCCAAAGCAAAAUUCAGACAAAGGCACCACCGACCACAGAGGUUUCUGGACAGAAAAGCGACACCUGAAGGAUCCUAUGAGAAGAGCAUCUUCCUUACAGAAUGCUUGUAAAGACAAAAUUGGCAGAAAUAAUGUAUGUCAAAAAAUAUAUAUCAAAAGAAAAUUAAGAUGACCUCACAUAAAAGAUAAUUUAAUUUUCUUGUUUCAUAUGUAAAUGUCAUUAUUUAAAAUAAAGUUGUUUCUUCUAAGUGAAAGGAAUUGUGAUCAGGUAUAUCAAUAAAAAGUUUAGAAGAAAGUGCAUUUUUAUUUUCAUUCAACAAUUGUGUUGCUGAAACUGUUGGAGAGACACAGGUUUAUACCAGUUUCCUAGCUGUCUCUAUAGUUCUGUGUGCUAUAGCUCACAGCUUGGUUUAGCUGGUUUGGCCAUAAUUGGUGUAUAGGAAUGCUUGUGAUUUUUGCACAUUGAUUUUGUAUCCUGAGAUUUACUGAAGUUGCUUAUCAGCUUAAGGACAUUUUGGGAUGAGACAAUGGGGUUUUCUAAAUAUUCAAUCAUGUCAUCUGCAAACAGAGACAAUUUGGCUUUCUCUCUUCCUGUCUGAGUACGCUUUAUAUCUUUCUCUUGCUCGAUUGCCCUGGCCAGAACUUCCAAUACUAUGUUGGAUAGGAGUGGUGAGACAGGGCAUCCUUGUCUUGUGCUGGUUUUCAAAGGGAAUACUUCCAGCUUUUGCCCAUGCAAUAUGAUAUUGGCUGUGGGUUUGUCAUAAAUGGCUCUUAUUAUUUUGAGAUAUGUUCCAUCAAUACCUAGUUUACUGAGAGUUUUUAGCAUGAAGGGGUGUUGAGUUAUAUCGAGGGCCUUUUUUUGCAUCUACUGAGAGAAUCAUGUGUUUUUUGUCAUUGGUUCUGUUUAUGUGAUUGAUUACGUUUAUUGAUUUGCGUGUGUUGAACCAGCCUUGCAUCCCAGGGAUGAAGCCGACUUGAUGGUGGUGGAUAAGCUUUUUGAUAUGCUGCUGGAUUUGGUUUGCCAGUAUUAUGUUGAGGAUUUUUGUAUUGAUGUUCAUCAGGAAUAUUGGCCUGAAAUUUUCUUUUUUUGUUGUUUUUCUGCCAGGUUUUGGUAUCAGGAUGAUGCUGGUCUCUGAAACUGAGUUAGGAAGAAGUCCCUCUUUUUCUAUUGUUUGGAAUAGUUUCAUAAAGAAUGGUACCAGCUCUUCUUUGUACCUCUAGUAGAAUUCAGCUGUGAAUCCAUCUGGUCCUAGGCUUUUUUUGAUUGGUAAGCUAUUAAUUACUGCCUUAAUUUCAGAACCUGUAAUCGAUCUAUUCAGGGAUUCAACUUCUUCCUGGUUUAGUCUUGGGAGGGUGUAUGUGUCCAGGAAUUUAUCAAUUUCUUCUAGAUUUUCUAGUUUAUUUGCAUAGAGGUGUUUAUAGUAUUCUCUGAUAGUAGUUUGUAUUUUUAUGGGAUGAGUGGAGAUAUCCCCUUUAUCAUUUUUUAUUGUGUCUAUUUGAUUCUUCUCUCUUCUUUAUUAGUCUGGCUAGUGGUCUAUCUAUUUUGUUAAUCUUUUCAAAAAAUCAGCUCCUGUAUUAAUUGAUUUUUUGAAGGGUUUUUCAUGUCUCUGUCUUCUUCAGUUCUGCUCUGAUCUUAGUUAUUUCUUGUCUUAUGCUAGCUUUUGAACUUGUUUGCUCAUGCUUCUCUAGUUCUUUUAAUUGUGAUGUUACGGUGUCGAUUUUACAUCUUUCUUGCUUUCUCCUGUGGGCAUUUAGUCCUAUAAAUUUCACUCUAAACACUACUUUAGCUGUGUCCCAGAGAUUAUGGUAUGUUUUUACUAUAUUAAGGUAAAUAAAGUUCAUUGUAUUUAUGUAAUAUUUUGUCUUCCUGGAGAGUAGGGAGGGGUUAGUGAGGAUUAAAUGAAAUAGCCUUGUCUGAGUAGAAUUUAUACACUGUAAUAAUGUAUUGCCUCUUUAAUGAUGAAAGAAAUAAUCUCUGCUGAUGUGAUCAUUUUUGUUGUGCCUUUUCAAGAAAAUAUAUGGGGCUAAAAUGUUAAAAUAACUUAUUUUCAAGUAGAGUACUAUAAUCUGAAAAUACAAUUGAGUACCUUCUUACUGUCCGUAAAUGAAUACUCUCAAAAGUUCUGAUAGUUUUAAUUAAGGUAAUAAUUAUGAAUGUCAUUCAUUUGUUUAAUGAAAAUGUCAAUAUUGGCAAAUAAAGCAUUUUAAUUUUUUCCUGUGGGAUAAGAAGCUUCCUUUGUAUUCAUCCCUCAACCUUUCAUUAUUCAAUACCAAAAGCUGUAGAGUAAAUCAGGGAAAGUCACUAGGUUGGUGUCAAUCCCUGGAUUUGAUUAUUGAGAGGCAAUUCUCCAUGAAAUAUUUUCAGAUUACCACACAGUCCAAUCUUUUUGAGGAAAGACCACUGGCAAACUUGGUUAAAGUAGGGUUGAAUAGCAAAUGUAUCUUGGAAGAUAGAGAUAGUAGGUUGCUUCAGAGAGGUUUAGAGACGUCUCCCCUGUAAACAUUUGCUAACAUCGCAAAAUAAAAGACUCUCCCUCACCUGAGGAAAGGAUGGGUCAAUGUGCCAGCCAAACUCCAAGUGUCAUAGUUUGUGAGUCCAUGGUGGUAUACUCAACUCUUGUCUGUGCAGGAUAACAUUAGUCUCUCAUAGCCUUCUCAGUGCUAAGAUGCUCUGUGAAUAUUCAACUAUCUGUUUUCUAAUCUAGACACUUUGUGUUUAUUACCAGAAGAGCAUCUAUUUAUCUAUCUAUCUAUCUAUCUAUCUAUCUAUCUAUCUAUAUCUAUCUAUCUAUCUAUCUAUCUAUCUAUAUCUGUCUAUCUCUAUCUAUCUAUCUAUCUAUCUAUCUAUCUAUCUACCUAUCACUGUGGCAGGCUGACUUUUUAGCUUAUAAAUAUAGUUAGUAGACUUAAUUUUAGAUAAUACAGAUGUCAUUCCUUUAUUAACCUCAUGCCAUGCUGAUGUUUGUAAUGAUGAGAAACGAGAAUCAUUUUAUGGUAUCGUUUAUCAAGAUAUUGUAUAUAUCAUGUGUUCUCUAUGAUACAUUCAAAAAACAGAUCCCAGUAAUAAUAUGUUUACAGUAUGGAGUUCUUUACACACACAUACUUUCAGGACAGUUGAGAUAGAGAGAUAAAAGCAUUUCCCUGGUGCCAGUGGUAGGUUUGAAUUUCUUUGAAACAUAUCAAGAUAAGGUGAUGCCAUGCAAAGAACAUGGUGACAUGGGUGCAGCAGAGUGUCAGCUAGGAGCAGACUAGAUUCAUCUUGGCGGACCUAGUGGACUAGUGAUAUCUGAGGCCUUUUAUGUGCAUGAGUAGAUCUAUGCAAGUUUUCCAGCUAAAGGAAGAAGGUGAUGUGUGCAUGUGUUUGUGUGUGUGUGUGUGUGUGCGUGCACACAUGUGCAUGCUAGAGUGCAGGAAAGAGACAAAGAUAAACAGGAAAGUUGGGAAAAUUUAGAAUAUAUUAAAAAAAACCCUAUAUCUUGCUUCCUGUUUGCCACAAUUAGCAUCACAGCCUCUGGAAGAUGCAAUGGUUAAUAAUUGCUGCUGAUUCUUUGAUAUGGCUUUUCCUGGGGACAGUAGGGAGUCAGCUUGAGUAAAGACAAAUCCUAGAAAGGGUGCUUUUUCAGGGAGAUUCCUAACAGCUAACAUAGUGGCAAUGCUCUUGGAAUCGAGUUUUUUUAGGAGCUCCAAACCCAGUGUCCCCCUCUUUGGUGGUUGCAAAGUUGCUUUUUCUCACAGCUACUGUGAUUGCAAGGCUGCUGGUUUUCAAGUCUGUCAUGCAGCUGAGAAGAAUUGCUAUAGGACAAUUCAAAACGUCACAAAGCUCACAUUCUUAUCAAGAUUUAGUCACUUUUCUUAAAAAAAAGAUUUCUUUUUCGUUAAUUUCUAGAGUUCUGCAAAAGUUGAUUCUGACAAAUUUUGCUAGUGGUCAUUGCCUUUAUGCUGAAAUAGAUUUUCAGAAGUCCUUAGCCUGCCAUUUCUAACUGUUGGUCUUGGGCAAAUUAUUUAAUCUCCCUUUUUCUCAAUUUUCUAGUUCAUAAAACAAGCAUAGUAACAUGCCCUAGAGAAUUGUUGUGAGGCUUAAGAAAGCUCAUUCAAGAAAACCACUUAGAAUAGUACUUGGUACCUAAUGAAUACUCAACCAACACUGGCUGUCAGUAUCAGUAUAUUCAUUUUAAAUACUUAAGUUUAGAUAUAAACAAACCUACCUUUUAUUUUUCCCAAAUUUUGGUUCUAUGCUCACUUUUUAUUUUUCUGAAUUGGUUUAUCUGGCUACAAAGUUUUACAGAUUCUAUUUCACAACGUUUCAGACCAUAGCAGUUGAUAAUGUUUUACAUUCCAUUACACAGACUAUUCCCUGAAGCUUUUUGGAACAAUAACAGAUGGCCAAGCUGUUGAAGAUAUUAUGAUUCUACUUACUGUUCAAAUAUGUAGGCUAGAACAGGGUAAUUUUGCUUUCUGUUACCUGAGAAAAAUAAGAAUGCCACAUUUAUUUAUGUACUUUUAUCCAUGUGGUUUAUAAAAUUUCACUUUUUGAGAGGAUUGUCCCAGGGUGCAAAUAGUGCAAAAUAUCUUAUUGAAUACCUAGAGCUAUCAAAGUCAUUAAUGUUUUAUAAAAUAUUCAAACUUUUAAUAAUAAAUAAAGCUGCUUCCUAAAAAGAUCUCCUACUAAGAGGGAGUACAUAUGAGAAGAUGAGGUACUUUCAGUGCCUUAAAUGUCAGCAAACUUGAGCCUGUCAGAAAAAGAAAAUGGGAAUUUCAUAAAUUGGUAUAAUAUGUAAUUACAAUGGCUAAUUCAAAAUAUUUAACAAUAAUUAAUUAUGAAAAAUAAGUAGUCUUUUGCCCUCUUUUCUAAAUGCUAUUAAUAUUAUUUAUGAUAAUAUUAAGCAUAGUACUCAUAUAAUGAGUCACUUCAUUAAAGAUAUUCUUAGGUUUUUUUGGUCUAUAUUUGUAGUAUUCUUAAGGCUCUGAUUUUUGAAUAAGGAGGAAAAGAUGGCUAACCUGGUUCACCAGUUGUUCUUUAACUUUAAAAGUGAACUGAGAUAUUUUAACGAUUAUAUUUUUAUAAUCCUUUUAUAUGGUAAAGAUUAAACCAAAUAAGAUCUAAAGAAGAUAAAUAUAGUCCACACAGAACUCUCUAGUUAAAUGUAUCAAUCUGGAGAAAGUAUUGUUUUUUUUUUUUUAAAUUUUAUUAUUAUUAUACUUUAAGUUUUAGGGUACAUGUGCACAACGUGCAGGUUUGUUACAUAUGUAUACAUGUGCCAUGUUGGUGUGCUGCAGAAAGUAUUGUUUCUUAAGGAUCAAAAUUUCAAUUCAGUUUUAUGCAAUUGUUCCUGUAUACCAUGGAUAUCAGAUAGAUAGAAAGACAGAUAGAUAGAUGACAGGUAGAUAGGUGAUAAAUAGAUAGAUGAUAGAUAGAUAGAUAGAUAGAUAGAUAGAUAAGAUAGAUAAUAGGUAGGUAGGUAGAUAAUAGAUUAGGUAGGUAGACAAUAGGUAGGUAGAUAAUAGAUUAGGUAGGUAGACAAUAGGUAGGUAGAUAAUAGAUUAGGUAGGUAGAUAGAUGACAGGUAAGUAGGUAGAUAGAUGAUAGGUAGAUAGAUAAGUAGGUAGGUAGGUAGGUAGAAAGAUAUUGAUAGGUAGAUAGAUAGAUAGAUAAUAGAUAGAUAGAUAGAUAGAUAGAUAGAUAGAUAGAUAGAUAGAUAGAUAGAUAGUGUGACUGCCUUUGCUAUCUGAAGAUUUAGAAUUAGAAUGCCUGUAUAGAUAAACCUUAUGAAAGUUAGGGCUCUUUCAGUUGUUAGAGAUAGAAAUCUCCUCUCAAACAGGCCUAAGUUUUUUUAAAAAGUACCCAUGUGUACAUAUAAUCUGAGAAGUCCAGGGGUUGAGCUCUUUCAGAAGUGCUGGAUUAAAGAGCUCACCACAGACUCCAUCUCAGCUCUACCUCAUCUGGGUAGUACAUUCACAGUUCCAUUACAGUGCUCAGUAUCUUCAGAGCCAUGACAUUAAAAAACAAAAGAAACAUUUCUGCUUCAGCAGUGACUCAAACAGAAGCCACAGAACUGAGUUUUGUUUCCCCUGAUUGGCCUGCUUUGUGUCGUGUAUGAAUCCCUGAAUUGUGUGUGUGUGAGAGGAUUUAAUGUGCUGAUGGACCAGUCAAGAUUACACAUUUGUUCUGGAGAUAGGUAUGUACUUCAUUCAGUUCAGGCAGACUGAGAAGCAAGAGGGAUAUAGCCUAAAUGAGAGUCUGGACUUUGCUGGAAAAAAGGGAAUUUUUUUUUUACAUAUACUUUAAGUUCUGGGAUACAUCUGCAAAACAUGCAGGUUUGUUACAUAGGUAUACAUGUGUCAUAGUGAUCUGCUGCACCCAUCAGCCCAUCAUCUACAUUAGGUAUUCUCCUAAUGCUAUCCCUCCCCUAGCCCUCCACUCACCAACAGGCCCUGGUGUGUGAUGUUCCCCUCCGUCUGUCCAUGUGUUCUCAUUGUUCAACUCCCACUUAUGAGUGACAAUAUGCGGUGUUUGGUUUUCUUUUCCUGUAUUAGUUUGCUGAGAAUGAUGGUUUCCAGCUUCAUCCAUGUCCCUGCAAAGGACAUGAACUCAUCCUUUUGUAUGUCUGCAUAGUAUUCCAUGGUGUAUAUGUGCCACAUUUUCUUUAUCCAGUCUACCAUCGAUGGGCAUUUGGGUUGGUUCCAAGUCUUUUCUAUUGUGAACAGUGCUGCAAUAAACAUACGUGUGCAUGUGCCUUUAUAAUAGAAUGAUUUAUAAUCCUUUGGGUAUAUACCCAGUAAUGGGAUUGCUGGGUCAAAUGGUAUUUCAGGUUCUAGAUCCUUGAGGAAUCGCCACACUGUCUUCCACAAUGGUUGAACUAAUUUACAUUCCCAACAACAGUGUAACAGUGUUCGUAUUUCUCCACAUCCUCUCCAGCAUCUGUUGUUUCCUGACUUUUUAAUGAUCGCCAUUCUAACUGGUGUGAGAUGGUAUGUCAUUGUGGUUUUGAUUUGCAUUUCUCUAAUCACCAUUGAUGAUGAGCUUUUGUUCAUAUGUUUUUUUGGCUGCAUAAAUGUCUUCUUUUGAGAAGUAUCUGUUCAUAUCCUUUACCCAGUUUUUGAUGGGGUUGUUUGAUUUUUCUUGUAAAUUUGUUUAAGUUCCUUGUAGAUUCUGGAUAUUAGCUCUUUGUCAGAUGGAUUGCAACAAUUUUCUCCCAUUCUGUAAGUUGCCUAUUCACUCUAAUGAUAGUUUAUUUUGCUGUGCAGAAGUUCUUUGGUUUAAUUAGAUCCCAUUUGUCAAUUUUGGCUUUUGUUGCCAUUGGUUUUGGUGUUUUAGUCAUGAAGUCGUUGCCCAUGCCUAUGUCCUGAAUGGUAUUGCCUAGCUUUUCUUCUGGCAUUUUUAAGGUUUUAGGUCUAAUAUUUAAGUCUUUAAUCCAUGUUGAGUUAAUUUUUGUAUGAAGUGUAAGGAAUGGGUCCAGUUUCAAUUUUCUGCAUAUGGCUAGCCAGUUUUCCCAACACCAGUUAUUAAAUAGGGAAUCCUUUCCCCAUUGCUUAUUUUUGUCAGGUUUGUCAAAGAUCAGAUGGUUGUAGAUGUGUGGCAUUAUUUCUGAGGCCUCUGUUCUGUUCCAUUGGUCUAUAUCUCUGUUUUGGUCCUAGUACCAUGCUGUUCUGGUUACUAUAGCCUUGUAGUAUACUUUGAAGUCAGGUAGCAUCAUACCUCCAGCUUUGCUCUUUUUGCUUAGGAUUGUUUUGGCUAUGUAGGUUCUAUUUUGGUUCCAUAUGAAAUUUAAAGUAGUUUUUUCUAAUUCUGUGAAGAAAAUCCAUGGUAGCUUGAUGGGAGUAGCAUUGAGUCUAUAAAUCACUUUGGGCAGUAUGGCCAUUUUUACGAUAUUGAUUCUUCCUAUCCAUGAGCAUGGAAGAGGAGGUGGAGUAUGGCCAAAUAGGAACAGCUCAAGUCUACAGCUCCCAGCGAGAUCUACGCAGAAGGUGGGUGAUUUCUGUAUUUCCAACUGAGGAACCCCACUCAUCUCACUGGGGCUGAUUAGACAGUGGGUGCAGCCCAUGGAGGGCAAGCCAAAGCAGGGCGGGGCAUUGCCUCACCAGGGAAGUGCAAGGGGUCAGGGAACUCCCUUCCCUAGCCAAGGGAAGCUGUGAGGAACUGUGUCAUGAGGAAUGGUGCAUUCCGGCCCAGAUACUAUGCUUUUCCCAUGGUCUUCGCAACCCACAGACUAGGAUAUUCCCUUGGGUGCCUACACCACUAGGGCCCUGGGUUUCAAGCACAAAACUGGGCAGCUGUUUGGGCAGACACUGAGCUAGCUGCAGGAGUUUUUUUUCCUACCCCAGUGGAACCUGGAAUGCCAGUGAGACAGAACUGUUCACUCCCCUGGAAUGAGGGCUGAAGCCAGGGAGCCAAGUGGUCUAGCUCAGUGCAUCCCACCCCCAUGGAGCCCAAAAAGGUAACAUCCACUGGCUUGAAAUUCUCGCUACCAGCACAGCAGUCUAAAGUUGACUUGGGAGCUUGUACUUGGUGCAGGGAGGGGUGUCCACCAUUACCAAGGCUUGAGUAGGCGGUUUUCCCCUAACAAUGUAAACAAAGCCACCGGGAAGGGAAGUUCAAACUGGGUGGAGCACACUGCAGCUUGGCAAAGCUGCUGUAGCCAGACUGCCUCUAUAGAUUGCUUCUCUUUGGGCAGAGCUUCAGCAGAUUUAAACAUUCCUGCCUGCUGGCUCUGAAGAGAGCAGCAAAUCUCCCCACACAGUGCUUCAGCUCUGCUAAGGGACAGACUGCCUCCUCAAGUGGAUACCUGAUCCCAGUGGCACCUGACUGGGAGACACCUCCUGGGAGGGGUCGACAGACACCUCAUACAGGAGAGCUCCAGCUGGAAUCUGGCUGGUGCUCCUCUGGGACAAAGCUUCCAGAGGAAGGAACAGGCAACAAUCUUUCCUGUUCUGCAGCCUCCACUGGUGAUACCCAGGCAAACAGGGUCUGGAGUGGACCUCCAGCAAACUCCAGCAGACCUGCAGCAGAGGGGCCUGACUGUUAGAAGGAAAAAUAACAAACAGAAAGGAAUAGCAUCAGCAUCAAGAAAAAGGAUGUCCAGACACAGAAACCCCAUCCAAAGGUCACCAACAUCAAAGACAAAAGAUAGAUAAAUCCACAAAGAAGGGGAGAAAUCAGCACAAAAAGGCUGAAAAUUCCAAAAACCAGAACACUUCUUCUCCAAAAGAUCACAACUCCUCACCAGUAAGGGAACAAAACUGGAUGGAGAAUGAGUUUGACGAAUUGACAGAAGUAGGCUUCAGAAGGUGGGUAAUAACAAACUCCUCCAAGCUAAAGGAGCAUGUUUUAACCCCAUGCAAGGAAGCUAAGAACCUUGAAAAAAGGUUAGAUGAAUUGCUAACUAGAAUAACCACUUGAGAGAAGAACAUGAUGACCUGAUGGAGCUGAAAAACACGGCACAAGAACUUUGUGAAGCAUACACAAGUAUCAAUAACCAAACCGAUCAAGCAGAAGAAAGGAUAUCAGAGAUUGAAGAUUAACUUAAUGAAAUAAGCUUGAAGACAAGAUUAGAGAGAAAAGAAUGAAAAGGAACAAACAAAGCCUCCAAGAAAUAUAGGACUAUGUGAAAAGACCAAUCAUACAUUUGAUUGGUGUACCUGAAAGUGACGGAAAGAAUGGAACCAAGUUGGAAAACACACUUCAGGAUAUUAUUCAGGAGAACUUCCCCAACCUAGCAAGACAGGCCAACAUUCAGAUUCAGGAAAUACAGAGAACACCACAAAGACACUCCUCGAGAAGAGCAACCCCAAGACACAUAAUUGUCAGAUUCGCCAAGGUUGAAAUGAAGGAAAAAAUAUUUAGAGCAACCAGAAAGGUUGGGUUACCCACAAAGAGAAGCCUAUCAGACUAACAGUGGAUUUCUCUGCAGAAACCCUAUAAGCCAGAAGAGAGUAGGGGCCAAUAUUCAACAUUCUUAAAGAAAAGAAUUUUCAACCCAGAAUUUCACAUCUAGCCAAACUAAGCUUCAUAAGUGAAGGAGAAAUAAAAUCCUUUACAGACAAGCAAAUGCUGAGAGAUUUUGUCACCACCAGGCCUGCCUUACAAGAAUUCCUGAAGGAAGCACUAAAUAUGGGAAGGAAAAACUGGUACCAGCCACUGCAAAAACAUACCAAAUUGUAAAGACCAUCAACACUAUGAAGAAACUGCGUCAACUAAUUGGCAAAAUAACUAGCUGGCAUCAUAAUUACAGGAUCUAAUUUACACAUAACAAUAUUAACCUUAAAUAUAAAUGGGCUAAAUGCCCCAAUUAAAAGACACAGACUGGCAAAUUGGGUAGAGUAAAGACCCAUCGGUGUGCUGUAUUCAGGAGACCCAUCUCCUGUGCAGAGACACAUGGGCUCAAAAUAAAGGGAUGGAAGAAUAUUUACCAAGCAAAGAGAAAGAAAAAUAAAAAGCAGGGCCUGCAAACAUAGUCUCUGAUAAAACAGACUUUAAACCAACAAAGAUCAAAAAAGACAAAGAAAGGCAUUACAUAAUGGUAAAGCGAUCAAUGAAACAAAAAGAGCUACUAUCCUAAAUAUAUAUGCACCCAAUACAGGAUCACCCAGAUUCAUAAAGCAAGUUCUUAGAGACCUACAAAGAGACUUAGACUCCCACACAAUAAUAUUGGGAGACUUUAACACUCUGCUGCCCAUAUUAGACAGAUCAACAAGACAGAAAAUUAACAAGGAUAUGCAGGGGAGAUAAAUUUUUGAUAGAAAAAGUUAUGGAAGAAAUAUACCUUUAGAGCUGUUCUUUAUGAAACAGAAAUUUUUGAACUAUUAGGAAAAUUGAAGCUAUAUAAAACAGUAUAAUUAGAACAUUAAGCUUUACAGGUGGUCUCUUCUAAAUGUCUCUUACUGGUGGAGCAACUAAAGGCCAAGAGAGGUUAUGAAAUUUUUCCUAUAUUUCACAGCUUUAACUCAUUUGAUUUGCAGAUUGACAAGCUCCACUAUUUUUGAUAAAAAUGAAUUUUGAGCUUCAAUUCAUACCCGUAUUAUAGCACUUCCUACACCACAUUAGAAAUACUAUUUCUCAUUGGAGCUCUUCAAUUCAGAGACAGUGUUUUAUUCUGUGCAAUAUAGUAUAUUUUUCAGUGACUUAAAAUUUUAUUUGGUAAAUGAAUGAGCAAAAUAAAAUGAGGGAAGUAAUGAGUAAUGAUUAACUCUACCUGAUUGGCAAAUCCAGAAGACUAUGUUAAUCUAACUAUCUCUUCUCCAAUAUUGACUUGAAAAACCUACUUGUAUGUCUCUGUCUCUGGAAAAUAAUGCAUAAAUUCAAACUCGUUGUUAACUCACUGAGAGAUUUGAGGAGGUUGUGAUGUUAAAGGGAAGGUGUCUGAAGUUAAACUCUAUUUAAGGAUAUAUUUUAUCAUUGUUUAAUGCCUAAAGAAGGAUCAGUCAGGGAGAAGGGCUUUUAAUUCCUUCUGAAAGAUGAUAAAGUCAAAAGUAAGUGAGAUCAGGCACUUAGAGGAACACGUUGAACCCUGAAUGUGCUCAGUAACUACCUUUUUGACAGAUUGACUGAUCAUCACAUGUAGGCAGUCUGUAGUUUCAGUUUUCUGCAGAAAUUUUCUUUCAUGGAAUCUUUGCCUAUGUUUCUCAGGAGAGAGAUAAUGUUGUAACAACUGACUAUGUACAUCCUGCAGAUAUAACACAUGAAGUUGCUCCUGAAUUAGAUGAAUCUGCUUCUGUGCAGUAUAAUAAAAUUAGCAUCAUAAAAUGAAAACCCGGGUUCAAGCAACCCAAUAGGUAUUAUUUCUUUAUUCUCCAAUUCCUUCCAUUUUUUUAGCAAAAAAAAAAAAAAAAAUUCCACUUGAGUGACUUUUAGGACUAGACUUUAAUAAACACUUCAGUAUAGUCGAACUGGAUGAAGUACUGUCAUAUAUAACUUACUAAAAAUAAAAUACAAAACUGCACACAUAAGGAAAAUGAAACAUUAUGCCCUGGGAACUUCCUUUUAAUGAACACAUGGCUUAUAUAUGACAAAAAAGAUCAGAUCACUGUCGUGGUAUACCUUAGGAUGUCUGCCUGCUUUAAAUGGGCUGGCAAAUCUAAAAGAGUUAAACAUGAGAAAUUUUCAAAUUUAUCCAAUAAGUAGAUUCCCUGAAAGAGGCGGCGUCUAUAAUCACAUUAAAUGUAAAUGGGUAAGCACUUCAAUAAAAGGCAGAAAUUGUUAGACUGAAUAAAAGGAAUUAAGACCCAACUACAUGUUGUCUACAGAUAAUGUAUUUUAAUUAUAAAAACACAUGUUGAUAGUAAAAGAAUGGAAACAGAUGUUCGUUGAUUAUAUAUAAAUCUACCAUUGAGAAGGAGGAAAACUAGCUCAUUUAAAAAAUCCAAUUCAGUUCCAAAUUCAUUUCCUAUAUUCUGUGCUAUAGGGAAGAUUGUCAGAAGGCAUCUUUCUUUUUAUAUUUGCUUCUGUUUGUUAGAUAGUACUGACUGAUUUGCUACUUCUGAGCAUUGGUUUUGAAAUAUACAUACACACACAUAUAAUUCCACCAGCAUUUGCUCAAAAAUUCCUUCAGCACUGAGACUGCAUUGAGAUUUCUACACUCAGUUUAGGUAUAUCUUCAAUUAACCAAAUUCUGGAAACCAACCCAGUAGUGUUUCUGCAUUUGUACAUUUGUCAAUGUACAUUUGUCAAGGUCCAGCCUUUGUAAUAGUAAGUAGAACAGCAUUCCUACAAUCUUGAUUGUGCAAAGAGUAGAUUCUUGUGAUUCAUAUAUUGGGGAACCUAGUCACCCCUCUGGAAACAAUUAUAGAACUCUGGAUGUCUAUGGCCUUUCCAUAUGUACUCUAAUCUGAAAAAGCAAUCUUUAGCAAAUCAUUCUAUUCAGAGAACCCAAAUGGUGUUUUAAAAAUAAUAAACAAAUAACCACUCUUUUUAUCAUAUAAAUAAUUAUUAAUUGAAUAUGGAAGUCUGAAAGAACGUAAAGAUAACUGAGCACAGUGGUGUUUGUCCAUUAUCUGGUAAGCAGCCCUUGCUUUCCAGCUCUCAGUCCAGCACUAAAAAUAGUUUCCAUAGUCUAAAAGAGUAAUUAGCAUGCUAUUCCCAGAUAGCCAAAAUUGUCUUUUUAAUUAACAAUAUAAUUGUUUGAAUAAAGACUUAGUCCUUAUUAGGCUAUGUAGUGAUAUGACAAAUCUUUUCUCUGUCUUGUAUUUUCAGCCCUGGAAAUUUUCAUUGAAAAAUGUGCUUUCCUGAAUGUAAUGUCUCAGGUAUUAUUAUGAAGAAUGGCCUAUAUAUCAAAGUGGCAUAAUAUUAUUUGAAACAUCUCUGCCACAAAUUACAAACCAAUAUUGUAAACCUAAAGCAACCUCUAAAAGUAGAUAAAUGAGGUAACACUAAUAAGAUAAUUGUGUAGAUAAAACAAAAUCUGAAAAUAUUUGCAAUUAAUGUAAGGCAGGAAAUAAGCAAAAAAGUAAAAAUGAAACAAACAGAAAAAAAAAAAACCCAAGGUGUUAAAUUUAAACUCAAACACAUCAAUAACCACUUUAAUGUAGAUGGGUAAAUACUCCAAUUUAAAAGCAGAAAUUUUCAACGUAAAUAAAAAAUACUCAACUGUAUGCUGUCUACAGAAAAUGUAUUGUAAAUAUAAAAAUGCAGAAAAGUUAAAAGAAUGGGAAAAUAUAUAUAUAUAAUUGUAACAUUGUUCAAAAGAAAGCUGGAGAGGCCAUAUAAAAUGGACUUUAGGGCAAGGAAUAUUACCAGAUAUAAAGGCGGAAAUUUUAUAACAAUAAUGAUCAAUUCAUCAAGAAGAUAUCACAUUUCUUAUAUGUGUAUGCAACUAAUAAGAGAAUGUUAAGAUACAUGAAAUAAAAACCUAUUAAUGUAAACAAAUAAACAGGGAAAUUCACAAUUACAGUUGAAACAGAACAUUCACCAAGAAGUAUAACCAAUAUCUAUGUUAGUUAUCUAUUGUUGCAUAAAAAAUUUUACCAAAACUUAAUAAGUAUAAACAGCAAACAUUCAUUAUGGCACAGUUUCUGUGAGUCAAGAAUCUGGGAGCAGCUUAACUCGGUGGUUCUAGCUAUGGGUCUUUUAUGAUGCUACCUCAGUCAAUGUGUCAGCUGGGGCUACAUUCAUCAAAAUUGCUGACUCAGAGGGGUUCUACUUUCAAAGUAAUUCACCCGCCUUGGGGCAGGCCCCAGAUGCUCUGAUCCAGGUCAGUCACAUGAGCCUCUGCACAGAGCUGUCUCUCAAAAUGGCAGCUGGCUUCCCCCAAGAAUGAGAGGUCCAAGAAAGAGUAUCUAAGACAGAAGCUGUAGUCAUUUUAUAACCUAAUUUCAGAGAUGAGAUUCCAUCACAUCUGCUUUAUUCUAUUUCCUAGAAGCUAGUCACUAAAUCCGCCUACAAUCAAAGUCAGGGGUUACACAAGGACCUAAAUGCAGGAGCCAGUGAUUACAGGUGGAACAUCUUAAAAACUGCCUACCACAGAAUAUAUCCUGGAGCAUAAAAAACAGUCUUGACAAAUUUAGAAGCAUAGACAAAUUAUGGACAUACAUUCAUUGAUGAAUGAAUUGAUUGGAAAUAAAUAACAAAAAGUUAUACAGAAAAAGUCCCCCGUUAUUUGGCAUUUGUUCAAUAUACUUUUAAAGAAUACAUGGGUCAAAGACAAAAAUCACAAGGAAAAUUAGAAAACAAUUUAAACCAGUUGAAAAGAAAACACAACAUUCUAUUGAAAAUGAAAACAAAAGUGCCAAUCUGAGAGAAAAUGUUAGAGAUACAUAUAUCUGGCAAAGUGCUUGUAUUUGUAAUACACUAAAAAAACCCUUGACAGCUUGACAAUAAGACAAAUAAAUGAUUAAAAAGAGAGAGAAAGGUUUGAACAACCAUUUUACAAAAAAGCAUAAAUGACUCUCAAAAGCAUUAUGCUUAGCCAAAGAAGCCAGAUAUUAAAGAGUAAAUACUGUAUCAUUUCAUUUAUAUUAAAUUACAGAAAGGCAAAACAGAAGAUCGUUUUUUGCCAGGGGUGGGGAACAUUCACUGCAAAAAAAAAAAAAGCAUGAAAUAAUUUUUGGUGGUGAUGGGAAAAAAUUCAGGGAAUGAGGUCAAACCCAGAGUGCUGCCAGUAAAAUCUGUGGCCUCAGGCUCACAAUCAAACCAAAGCUAUGGUUGUAAUUUGGUUGAGAUUUCAGGAAAUUGUGGAAGAGUGUCUCAUUUUCCUCUCAGCAGAAAUUGCUUCUAAGAAUUUUAAGGACAAGACUCUUUGGCCCUCUCUGCUGUGAGGGUCUUCACAAGUAACCCCAAAUAGAGAAAGACUCUACUCAGAGAAAUAGGUGGACGUCACUUUUGUCUAAUGAAUUGGAUUAUAAUUUGUACACAAGUCCACAUAUUUUAAAAGGAAUUAUAAUAGCCUGGACUGAAAGGAACAGACACUGCUCAAAACAUAAAAACACUUUUGCGUCCCCAACUUCUUAUGGGCAGAAAGCAGGCUAAGAACACUAUGCAGCUGCAAACAUAUGUCAUUAAAGAGUUCAUGGUGUGCUGCCAGGCGUCAAGAAGAACCACCCCAGGGAACAUAUAUGGGUCCUAAUCAACAUAUGCCCUGCCUCCUGAGCCAGGUGAAAUGGUAGGUAGCUUGUUCCUACUGGAUCUCAGAAUUUUCUCAUCCCAGUGACUACAAUGUCACUCACAUUGUCCUGCCUCUUUUUAAGUGGAGGUAUGUAUUGUGGUUCUCUUGAUCAUGUCUCCUCAUCGUAAGGUGGAAAUGUGUGGGCAUAUAGCUGGUUUCUUUAUUUGAUGGUCUUCUGAUCAAGAGGAAGUUCCACCCUCACCCUACUAGCCUCAAUCUAUUUGCUUUAGAAGCCAGUUGCUAAAUACAGCAGCUUGACUUGAUUUACAUGAUGAGAUUCUGAACUUAAAGUAUAAUACUGAUGGUGAUGAGAUUUGGGGGUUUAGGCAGAUUGGUAAGUGUUAUUUUGAAAGUGAGAGGAAAAUGCAUCAUCCUUGGCUAGCGGACUAAGUGUGGUAGCUACUCUCCAAAAAUAGCCCCAAUGAACCAGCUCUCCUAGUCGCUAAGUUCUACCAUAGUACAUAUGUGCUAUCUCUGUGAUUUGCUUUAAGCAAUUAGAUGUAGUACAAGUGUUUCUGGGCCAGUUUCUGGUGUAAGCCGUAAGAAGGCCUGGUAGGUUCUGGCCGGGCGCAGUGGCUCACGCCUGUAAUCCCAGCACUUUGGGAGGCCGAGACAUGUGGAUCAUGGGGUCAGGAGAUCGAGACCAUCCUGGCUAACACGGUGAAACCCCGUCUGUACUAAAAAUACAAAAAAUUAGCUGGGCAUGGUGGCUGGCGCCCUUAGUCCCAGCUACUCGGGAGGCUGAGGCAGGAGAAUGGUGUGAACCCGGGAGGCGGAGCUUGCAGUGAGCGGAGAUGGCGCCACUGCACUCCAGCCUGGGCGACAGAGCGAGACUCCGUCUCAAAGAAAAAUAAAAAUUAAAAUUAAAAAAUUAAGAAGGACUGGUAGGUUCUGCUUUGCUUUUUAGGAUAGCUCCACGCUGCCAUGUAAAAAUGUUGGCUAUUUUGUUGGAGAGUCGAUUUGGAGAUGCAGUUGUCACAGCAUCCCAGCAGCUGAGCUGAGAUACUCAGCUUUCUUCACCAAAGUGCCAGGCGUGUAGUGAGCCAUCUUGGAUAUAGCAGACCCAGUUGGCAUCACAUGGAGUUGGGCCUAGUUGAUUCACAGAAUGGUGGAGACAAUAAAAUUAUCUCGUUUUAAAUUAUUAAGUUUUGCAGUGAUUUGUUAUUCAGCAAUAGAUAACUGGGCCUCUAAUAUAAGCCAUUAACUGUAUGAGACCAUAAGAUUAUACUAAAUACAAAUGAAUAAAUUUGCUAUUUUUUAUUUUCUUACUUUGAAUUUUAACUAACCUUAAAUUUUUUUCUCUGUCAUAAAUUUAUUUUCGGUAGCCACCAAUAUUAGAGCUUUGUACAGUUGUUGCUAUAUUGAUUAUAUACUUUAGGUUUUUUGGCUUCUUUAUUAAGGUUGCUUUUUUCAAAGUUAAGUGACAGUUUAAGUCAUUUAUAGAUCUUGGCAGCAAAGAAGAUACCAGAUGUCACAUAUGUGAUGAAAAUAUCCACAAUCUUUUUGUUGUCAUGAAAAUAUAUUUUUAAAAUCCUUUAACAGAAAUUUAGAUAUGUAGUAGCUUAUCAGUCAUAGGAAAACAGAUAAUUUUUUAAAUACAUAAAGUACUUUUUAGAUUUCUAAAUGUUUUUAACAGCGUUCUAAUUUUAAUGGUAAAAACUGGAUAAAAACGUUCAAAUACUCUCUAAAAAUGUAAAUUCUUCUUUUAGAAGUUUCUAGCAUUAGAAUUUGGCAUAUUAGCCAUGCUGUAAUAUAUCUGGAGUCUUUGUGAUGAUCAAAAUGGUGAUUCUUUAAUAAGCUGGUACUCUAAAAACUUUCUGAUAGGUCUCAAUGCUUCCAUAUCAGUUUAAUUAUAUGAGACUGUUAUAAAGAGCUACGUUCUUUGUCUUACUCCCCAAGGAAGUACAUUCCAGGGCAUAAUUCUAUUCUCUUAUCAGCAAAAUCUUGGGAUUAUCUCUAGCUUCUAAAUUAUUUUUCUAUCCUCAAAAUCAUGCAAAAAGUUACUUAGAUGCUUUAGGUACUUAGUUUGAGUCAGCAUAUCUUUACAUGCGUACAGACAUUGCAUUUUGGAACUUAUCCAGUGCUAUCAAGUUGAUUUAACAUAACCAUUUUUAUGCUAAGUAGGUCAUGACUGGCAGAGCCAAGAGAAGUCUAAUAAACAAAUGUUAAUAUUCUAUAGAGUAAUAAUUCUUUUAAGACUGAGCUGCCCCCAAACGCCCUCAAAAUGAAAAGAAUAAACCUCUAAAUUAUCCACCAGAAUUUCUUACAUUUUCAGACUUUUCUGGGAGUAUAAACAUCAUAAUAAUAUCGGAUUUGAGAGAUAUUUGUUUUCUUUUAAGGGAAGAGCCAUCAGAAUUAGAAUCUGUUGGCAAGCAUGCCUACUAAAUAGGUUGAGUGUGUAGUCUUUGGCAAGACAGAAACAAGAAGAUAUGUGAGUGCUUCUGACUGUACAAAAAUGAAGUAUCACAUCCAAAUUCUUUCUAGAGGAUAACACCAAGACCUUGAUUUUUAAGCAAUUAAACUUGAAAGGAAAUGCUUUUUUAGCUCAGAUGCUAGAACUUUUCCUUAAAAAUGAAGAUUCUGAAAAGUGGACAAAUGAUCCUGUUUCCCCAUUGUAUGUUGAGGAGAAACAUACAAUAAAUAGAAAAUUUACAGAAAUCUAAAUAACCAAUAAAUACACAAAGGCCUACCUAAUCUCACUAAAAUUCAAGAAUAUUCAAAAUUUAUUUUAAUUCACCAGGGGCAAAAAUGAAAAAAAUAUUUUAAUUAAGCAGAGAGUGUGAGAAAAAUAAUUAUCUUGUGCCUUGUAUGUGUACUUUUUGACCUAGCAAUUCCACUUAACAUUAUCUGUCUUAUUAAAAAAAAAACCAUAUGUGCAUUCAUGAGAAUAAUCAUUGUUGCACUAUCUCACAUAAUUAACACAUGGAAGAAAUCUAGAUAUCUAUUAAUAGGAGGAUGAUUAAAUAAAUCAGAAAAACCCAUACUAUAAAGCAUUUUAGAAGAAUGCGGCAGAGACAGAUUUAAAUAUACUGAAAUAAAGGUGCCCAAGAUAUAUUAUUAAGUAAAAAAGCAAGUUACAAAACAAACUACAGUCUUCCAUUUUUUAAAAACAUAAAACUAAAUCGUACAUUUCCAUAUGAUCAUAUAUGCCUUAUGAUAUAUGUAUAUGGUGUGAUGCACAUGUGCCAUACUGAUUGCAGUAACCCUUGGGGAAGGAAGAGGAAGAUAUAGUGGGCUAAGGGCUAUUCAUAUAAUAACUUUGUAAUUAUGGAGAAGUAAAAAGGAUGGGGGAAAGUUCGUAGUGUAACUUGAAAUAAUCCCAUCUUUGGUUUUAAACAAUCAAUGCUUAAGUGAAUUGUAAUUAAUGAUUUUCACAGUUCUAACUUCCAACUUGACAUUGGUAUUUUCUAUAGAAUAUAAAGGUAAUUUUUCAAAGAUCAGAAUGUUGUAGAUGUGUGGUGUUAUUUCUGAGGCUUCUGUUCUGUUCCAUUGGUCUAUAUAUCUGUUUUGGUACCAGUAUCAUGCUGUUUUGGUUACUGUAGCCUUGUAGUAUAGUUUGACGUCAGGUAGUGUGAUGCCUCCAGCUUUCUUCUUUUUGCUUAGGAUUGUCUUGGCAAUAUGGGCUCUUUUUUGGUUCCAUAUGAACUUUAAAGUAGUUUUUUUCAGUUCUGUGAAGAAAAUCAUUGGUAGCUUAAUGGGGAUGGCAUUGAAUCUAUAAAUUACCUUGAGCAGUAUGGCCAUUUUCAUGAUACUGAUUCUUCCUAUCCAUGAGCAUGGAAUGUUCUUCCAUUUGUUUGUGUCCUCUUUUAUUUCAUUGAGCAGUGGUUUGUAGUUCUUGAAGAGGUUCUUCACAUCCCUUGUAAGUUUGAUUCCUAGGUAUUUUAUUCUUUUUGUAGCAAUUGUGAAUGGGAGUUCACUCAUGAUUUGGUUCUUUGUCUGUUAUUAGAGUACAGGAAUGCAUGUGAUUUUUGCAGUGAUUUUGUAUCCUGAGACUUUGCUGAAGUUGCUUAUCAGCAUAAGGAGAUUUUGGGCUGAGACAAUGGGGUUUUCUAAAUAUACAAUCAUGUCAUCUACAAACAGGGACAAUUUGACUUCCUCUUUUCCUAAUUGAAUACCCUUUAUUUCUUUCUCUUGCCUGAUUGAACUGAUCUUUGACAAACCUAACAAAAACAAGCAAUAGAGAAAGGAUUCCCUAUUUAAUAAAUGGUUCUGGGAAAACUGGCUAGCCAUAUGGAGAAAGCUGAAACUGGAUCCCUUCCUUAUACCUUAUACAAAAUUUAAUUCAAGAUGGAUUAAAGACUUAAAUGUUAGACUUAAAACCACAAAAACCAUAGAAGAAAACCUAGGCAAUACCAUUCAGGACACAGGCAUGGGCAAGGACUUCAUGGGCAAAACACCAAAAGCAAUGGCAACAAAAGCCAAAAUUGACAAAUGGGAUCUAAUUAAAGAGCUUCUGCACAGCAAAAGAAACUAUCAUUAGAGUGAACAGGCAACCUACAGAAUGGGAGAAAAUUUUUGCAAUCUACCCCUGUGACAAAGGGCUAAUAUCCAGAAUCUACAAAGAACUUAAACAAAUUUACAGGAAAAAAAUCAAACAACCCCAUCAAAAAGUGGGCAAAGGAUAUGAACAGACACUUCUCAGAAGAAGACAUUUAUGCAACCAAAAGACACAUGAAAAAAUGCUCACCAUCACUGGCCAUUAGAAAAAUGCAAAUCAAAACCACAAUGAGAUACCAUCUCACACCAGUCAGAAUGGUGAUCAUUAAAAAGUCAGGAAACAAUAGGUGCUGGAGACGAUGUGGAGAAAUACGAAUGCUUUUACACCGUUGGUGGGACUGUAAACUAGUUCAGCCAUUAUGGAAGACAGUGUGGCAAUUCCUCAAGGAUCUAGAACUAGAAAUACCAUUUGGCCCAGUGAUCCCAUUACUGGGUAUAUACCCAAAGGAUUAUAAAUCAUGCUGUUAUAAAGACACAUGCACACAUAUGUUUAUUGUGGGACUAUUCACAAUAGCAACGACUUGGAACCAACUCAAAUGUCCAUCAAUGAUAGACCGGAUUAAGAAAAUGUGGCAAAUAUACACCAUGGAAUACUAUGUAUCCAUAAAAAAGGGUGAGUUCAUGUCCUUUGUAGGGACAUGGAUGAAGCUGGAAACCAUCAUUCUGAGCAAACUAUCACAAGGACAGGAAACCAAACACCACAUGUUCUCACUCAUAGGUGGGAAAUGAACAGUGAGAACACUUGGACACAGGGUGGGGAACAUCACACACUGUCAUGGGGUUGGAGGAUGGGGGAGGGGUAGCGUCAGGAGAAAUACCUAAUGCAAAUGACAGCUUAAUGGGUGCAGCAAACCAACAUGGCACAUGUAUACAUAUGUAACAAACCUGCACGUUGUGCACAUGUACCCUAGAAUUUAAAGUAUAAAUAUAUAUAUAUGUAAGCAUAUAAAGGUAAUUUUUAAGGGCCUUUGUCUAAUGGAGCAGAAAUAAAACUUUCAUAAGCCAGAACAACAAGCAUGACUGGCCGUAGAGAACAAUGCCUGACUGCUUAAGCUUUGUGACUUUCAGCGUGUUGCUUCGUCUGUGCCACUCUCUCUUCACUUGUAAAAUGAGGGAUGAAAUGUAUUUAGUAAGUGCCUGGGAAAAAGCAAAGAACAUAUUGUAGGACAACACUUAAUGCACUGCCAAGCAAGAUACUAAAAACAAAAAAAAAAAACAAAAAAAAACUGGUCUAUUUUCAUUUGUUCACAAUAAACACAACAAUCUUAGAAGUUUAAUGCAACUCCUUCAAUGACUGACUAGAACAAUGUGAAGAAAACCAAGGAGAACCAAUUCAAAUGACUUACACAAUUAAAUGGCAUCUUAAAAAUGUUUGAUUAAAGUCUGUUUCUUUCUUCUUCGCAUCUUUCAUUUGAAGUGUGGAUUUAAGAAAUCAAAAAAAUGGACCCAAGUAUAAUUAAUGUUUCAUAUUCCUGCAGAGUCCAAAGUUGACCAGAAUCCAGCCAGCCAGCUAGCAAAGGAAGUUUACAAAGUAAAUACGAAAUGAACAUUGUCUUUUGGUGAUGUGUUUGAAACACUGCAACAUUUGCAUUUUAGAUUAAGCUCAACACUAUGUUGUCUCAGGUUGUAAGAUCAUCAGUGUUGAUCUUCAGGAUAAACAGGAAAGAUUGAUUACGUGCACUAAGAGCUAAGAACAGGGAAGCCAAAAGGAUUAGAGCCUGUUCAUCGAAAGCAAAGCCAAUAUUUAAAAGGUGAUACUUUUGCAUACAUCAUCCAGCUACAUCGAGGUAACUGCACAAAGCAUGAGAGUAACUUGGGAACUUUUGUUUACAAACAUUUUAAUUUUUGGAAAAUAUUAAAUACCUGAUCUAAAUAACUGUCUGAAUGCAUAAGUAAUUCAGCUAAUUGUGCUGUCUGAUUUCAAUAACUUGAAUUUAAAAAAUAUAAUUAAUAAUAUUUGAAGGUCUGUUUCACACGUUGCCUCUAUUCUUUUAUAAAAGAAAUUUUCCUUUUUUAUUUUUGGAGGAAAAGGCAUACAUAUUUUAAAAGGAAGCAUUGAUUAGCAUCUCUAUUCUAUUGUUUUUGUUGCGAAGUACUGUUUCUUUUUAGGUGAGCCAACUCUCCCUUCAGACUAGAAAACUGAUGAUGAAGCAAAAAUAUUUACACUUUGAAGUCAGAAGGAACAGCUUGUGGGGUUGACAGAGGCAAGGGGAGGGAAAUGUGCUUGGAGUUGUUAACAAAUCCGGAAACACAGUGUGGCAUUUAAGUUAGUUAGAAGGGAGGGAAGCUGAAUCCCUGAAAUACAAAUAAGGUUAGUUAACAUUUAUUUUACUCUGAAAGUACACUUCUUCAAUUAAAGAAGUAUCAUGUUGUUCAUUAAUUUAUAAUCUGUGUGAAUUAAAAAUUAUUAAAUAUCUAGCCUCAGAUGUAAAUUGUGUGUUUAUGUGCAUGUGGGUGUAUAGUUCAGAGAAAGUGAUUGUAAGAAGAAAGGGAAAGAUGUAUUAAUGAAUAUUUUGGAGGGCCUCUAUCAUAAAUCAUUAAUAACUACUCAUGAAAGACUGUAUCAGACCCACGGAACAAAUAGUCAACAUGCCCCAUAAGGACUUUAGAUCCACUAUGGACCACAUAUAUACAGUGGUCUCAUAAGAUUAUAAUGAAGCUGAAAAACUUGUUUCACCUAGUGAGGUCGUAGCUGUCAUAACUUUGUAGUGCAACACAUUACUCACUUGUUGUGGUGGUGCUGGUUUAAAUAAACCUACUGCAUUGGUGGUUGUAUAAAAGUAUAGUACAUAUAAUUAUGUAUAUAAAACUCGAUAAUGAUAAGAAAUGACAAUAUCAAUGGUUUAUAAUAUACAUUUUAUCAUUAUUCUAGAGUAUAUUCCUUCUACUUAUUAAAAAAAGUUUACUGUAAAACAAUCUCAGGUAGGUCCUUUUGGAAGUAUUCCAAACAAAGGCAUUGUUACCAAAGGAGUUGACAACUUCAUGUGCACUACCCCUGAAGUCCAGUGGGACAAGACGUGGAGGUCGAAGACAGUGAUGUUGAUGACCAUGACCCUGUGUAGGCCUAUGUUUAUGUGUGCUCUUGGGUCUUAGUUAAAUAGUAAAAGUAAAAAUAAAAAUAAAAAUUUUAAACAUUGAAAAAAAAGCUUAUAGAACAAGGAUAUAAAGAAAAUAUUUGGCCUGGUGUGGUGGCUCACGUCUGUAAUCCCAGCACUUUGGGAGGCCAAGGCUGGCAGAUCACUUGAGGUCAGGAGUUUGAGACCAGCCUGGCCAACAUGGUGAAACAGUGCCUUUACUAAAAUACAAAAAAUUAGCUGAGUGUGAUGGUGCACAUUUGUAAUCCCAGCUACUUGGGAGGUUGAGGCAGGAGAAUCACUUGAACCCGGGAGGUGGAGCUUGUAGUGAGUCAAGAUCGUGCCACUGCACUCCAGCCUGGGUGACAGAGCGAGACUCCAUCUCCAAAAAAAAACAAAAAAAAAGAAAAUAUUUUUGUACAUCUGUACAGCAUAUUUGCAUUUUAAGUUAUGUUAUUAACAAAAGAGUCAAAAAAUUAAAACAUUUAUAAAGUAAUAAAGUUACGGUAAGCUAAGUUUAAUUUAUUAUUGAAGAAAGAAAUUUUUUUAAUACACUGAAUGUAGCCAAAGUUUACAGUGUUUAUAAAGCCUACAGUAGAAUACGGUAAUGUCCUAGGCCUUCAUAGUCACUCACACUAUUCACUCACUGACUCAUCCAAAGCAACUUCCAGUCCUUCAAAUUUCAUUCAUAGUAAGUGCCUUAUAUUGAUGUACAAUUUUUAAUCUUUUAUAUCAUAUUUUUACUGUAUCUUUUCUAUUUUAUAUAUGUUUAAGUACAAAAAUACUUACCAUUGUGUUACCACUGCCUAGAGUAUUCAGUACAGGAACAUAAUAUACAUACAGGUUUAUAGCCCAGGAACAAUAGGCUAUCCCAUUUAGCCUAGGUGUGUAGUAGGCUGUACCAUCUAUGUUUCUGUAAGUGUACUCUGUGGUGCUUGCACAAUGACAAAAUUGACUAACGAUGCAUUUCUCAGAAAGUAUUCCUGUCAUUCAGUGAUGUGUGACUUAAGUGAGGAAGAAAAUUAUGUUAUAUAGAAGUAGAAUACAAAGGAGGCUAACUCUGAUAACUCAUUAUUUGUAUCAAAAGUAUCAUCAAAUUAAACAUGUUUAAAAAACAAAGAUUUUCAAAUGCUACUUAAUAGUUCAUGCUUCAUAUUUCAUUCAACAAAACUGUUGGUUACAACAUCAAUCAGGCAAAAAGGAUACAUGGAAUGUGCGAAAUUCACUUUGGGGAUUUCUGGUAUGCAUUAAAAAGAUGUAAAGAUAUAAGCAGCUAUUAAGGGAGGUAAGACUGCAAUAUAAUGGACCUGACUGAUGAUGAUUCAGAGUUUGUUAGAAUUGUGAUAUUAAGGCACCAUGGACAGAGAAUAUUAGACAGCGAUUUCAAAUAUAUACUGUCAAUUGAAAGUCAGGAGUGCAGAUGCUUUGAAUUUGGGGUGCUAAAUUUUGAUCUGUUUGCUUCUACAUUAGCCACUAGCCACUCAAUAAAGUAUUGCUCUAGGUUGAGAAUCAAUAAAAAUUUAAGAAUAAUUGAACAUUUUUUCCAAGGAAUGUUGUAUUGAUCAACUAGCAUUCAAAUACAUGUAUGCACCGAUUAUUGACUAUGAUAUGUUCUGAGAAAUGCAUCAUUAGGCAAUUUCAUUGUGUAAAUAUUAUAGAGUGUACUUAAGCAAACUUAAGAUGGUAUAGCCUACUACACAUCUAGGCUAUAUGGUAUGACCUAUUGCUUCUAAGCUACAAACCUGUACAUUAUGUUAUUGUACUGAAUACUGGAGGCAAUUGUAACACAGUGGUAAGUAUUGUGUAUCUAAACUUAUCUAAACAUAAAAAGGCACAUUAAAGAUACAGUAUUAUAAUCUUAUGGAAUCACCAUUGUAUGUGUGGUUCUUUGACUGAAAUGUAAUGUGGCACAUGACUGUAUACCCGAUCAGUUCAAUUUUGAUUAAAUAGCUCGAGUAGUAGUUCCUUACAUUUGGCAUUACAAAUUUCUUUUCAUUAUUUACAAACAGUCUUCAUUUGCAAUAACUGGUAAUAAUUCAUAAUUUACCACAACUGAAAUUGAAUCUCUAUGCUUCACAGCUAGUGACCUGGUAUCAGCUUCCUCAUCCAUUUUUCCUAGUUGAAAAUUCAUCCCAAUUUGGGCUUUUAUUGUUCUCUCUUUAUCAUCUUCCAUGCAGCUACAUUCAUGACACGAUGCAAACUUUGUUGCAUUGUGAAAUACUUCCCAGACAGUAGGCAACCAAUAAAGUUGGUGAGCAAUAAAGAGGUGGAAGAAAAUAACAAUUCUUAUCUCUCAAAUGACUUUAUAUACGAUUUUGGCUUUGUGUUAUUAGAACCAUUAAGAGUCUGAAGAGACCUUUCAUAUAUUUUUUUAUUCUGCAUUACUGAAUUUUUAAGAAAGAAAUUAUGUGCUAUAAUAGUGUUCUUGACUUUGAGAAUUCUUGAAAGUCUCAACGGGUAUCCCUGGAGAAUGUAAGGGUCUCCUGUAAUAAGAUUAGAUUUAUGAGAGACUUGUAGUUUAUAUGAAGCUUUCAAAUUCACAGUUAAUGAGGUUUCCCUGGUGGUGGCUCAUACAAAUGAAGAUGUCAGAACAAAAUGAAGCAUAAACUCCUACUGCAAUUGGGGGGUCUAAUUUCAUGAUAAUGUGGAAAGAGAGAGAGAGCAAAACAUAUAACAACAUUUAUGUUAAUCUUCAGGAAAAGCAGAGUUAAAAUAACUUCUAGAUAUUUUAAGUAAUAGAUAAGAAAAUAAAGAUACUCAAAAAUCUAAUGAUAGAUAGGAAAAAGGAAUGGGAGGACAAUACCCAAACUGUUCUUGAGCCAUAGUCUGGUUAUCAAUGACUGCCAGUGCUUUAGGGUAAUACCAGCAUGCAACACCUGUCUUGGAUCAAUGUUAUUACCAACUGCAUUAUUUUAGGAAAUAAGGCCUGAAAUAGUCAAGGAGUGGAUAAGGAGAGGUGUUUGUAGCCUAGUGUCCCAUUUAGGCCUUCUCUGCAGCUAUGAUAUCUCUGUAUAAACUUAAGAAACAUUUUCUUUUAUAUUUUAUUCUUAUUGAUUAUAGGAGUCUGCUGCAGACAUGCAUUUCCUAACCACUUUUUAAUGUUUUAAUGUUUCUUUAGUAUUAAUUCUAUACCAAAAUUAAAUGGACGUUACUAUAGUAAAAAAAAAAUGCCUCAAGAUUAUAGAGUUCAACAAAAUGAAAGAGAAAGAGAAGCUAAAUUUUGGCAAAUGACUGUGGAAAAAAAUACAGAAAAUGGGUUUCACCUUAUUUAGUCUCUACCUCAUGGGGUUUUAUAAGUAUUAAAUGGGAUAAAGUUUGUGCAAUGCCAGGUACCUAGUAAACACUCAGUAAAUAUUGCCAAUCAUAAAGCCUUCUAUUACCAAUUUUCUGAUACGAAAUAUCUUGCACACUUUCCUGUGUCUUUCUUUCUAAACUUGGGAUAAAUUUCAUGAUACUCUCAUUUGUUUCUUCCUUAACUACAUCUAAUUAAACCAGAUUUUAGGAAUCUAUAAGUUAUAUGCCCUCUCUGAAUGAUCUCUUCGAUAGUAAUAUAAUGUGAGCCACAAUUUUGAGUCAUAUAUGUAAUUAAAAUUUUCCUAGUAACUGUAUCAAAAAAGCAAAAAGAAACAGGGAAAAACUUCUUUGAGUGAUAUACUUUAGCAUGAUAUUUACAAAAUAUCAUCAGUUUCAUUGAUUUACAUGUAAUCAAUGUAAAAUUAUUAGACAAAACUUACUUUUACAUUUUAAAAAUCUAGUACUUAUAUUAUACACAUCUCAGUUCAGACUAUCCACAUUUCAAUAAUUCAAUAGCUACCUGGUCAAUGUAGUUUUAUAUGAAGAGAAAAUGAAGUUUACAAUAAAGAAAAUUAUCUCUAGUUACAUAUUUUCAAUCAUUUGCAAGUGGAUAAGGUAACUUUUUUCAUGGAUCAUGAUAAGUAAGGAGAGUAGAAAAGCUAGGACAAAGACCUUUUUUUUGGUUUGUUUUUGUUUUAAAUCACUUCUAAUUAUAACCUACUUUGUUACGCAGAAGUCUAGAGUUGGGCAGAAACACCUGUCUCAAACAGCCAUCAAUUCUUUGGAGUAUUCAAAAUUAACUUUUGUUUGGGAUGAUGUUAGUUAGUUAAUCUAGUCAUAGCCACAACACGAAUAUUGAUUUUUGAUGAUUCAAUGAGAUAAUGCACACAAAAGCAUUCUGUAAGUUAUACAGCACUAUAAAUGCAUAGUGAGGAUCAAGACUAUUUUAAUCACAUAGAGAAUUCAUUGGUGAGUGCACCUAAAUUAAAAUAUAAUGCUUUCCCUUUCCUUUCUAAAUUGACCUUUCCCUGUACAAGUUAUUCAUGGAAAUCAGACACAUUCUUUUCUUUCUUAAACUCUUAGGUCUCAAGCUAAUAGGUAAGAGAGUAAACCCUGGUUGGGAUUAAUUUUUCAAAGGGAAUACUUAAAAGCAUUCCCUUUGUCUUUCCUUUCAUUUCCCCAAUCCAAUUAUUUCAUACUUAUAUAAUGGUUGUAUGGGUCUCCAAUUAUCUAUCUUUUUUUUUCAGUGCAGAUAAACAGCUGAUUAAAUCUUUCUUUGAUUUUUAUGAAAUGUAGUAACUUGGUAGACAACACUGAAUGUAUUACUUCUGUGUAUGUAGCCUAGAAAUACUUAGAACAAUGGCAGCAAAAGCAGGUAAUGCAAGGGAGAUGAUAGAAAUGAGAAAUUAAAGCAAGGUCAAUGCCAAUUCCAUAGGCUAAUUAUAGUUUUCAGUGCAUUAUGAGUAUUGAAAACUGUUUAGAUUGAGUAGAGGAAAUAAUGGAGAUGGUGACAGUUAUUUUAAUUAAUUAGAGUGGCCAGGGAAUGAAGUGAGCAAGACAAUCAUGUCUACUUCUGAGAGAAGAACCUUUCCAGGUGGAGGGGACUGACAAUGCAAAGACCUUGAAGUAAUAAGUUUCUUGUCAUGGCUGGAAUAGAGAUGAAUGGUAGUAUAUUUUAUCUGAGAGCUGGCAGAGAGCCAGAGUGCAUAAGGAAUGAUAAGCGCUUUAGAUUUCUUUUCUGAGUAAGACAGGAUGCCAACAGAGGAUUCAUUUUUGUAUUUGUUAUUGUUUCAGUUCUGGUAAGAAGACAUGAGAUCUAUCAUUGUAACAAAUUUUUACCUAUACAAUAUAAUAUUGUUGAAUAUAGAUACCAUAUUGUAUACAAUAUCUUUAGAGCUUAUUCAUCUUCCUUGACUGAAACUUAAUUUGUCACUCCUCAUUUCACUGUCUUCCCACCUGACAACCACCAUCCCUUUCUGGGAUUCUAUGAAUUUGCCUAGUUUUAGAUACAUCAUAUAAUAGAAUCGUGAUAUAUUUAUCUUUCUAUAACUGGCAUAUUUCAAUUAGCAUAAUGUCUUCCAAUUCAUACAUGUUGUCACAUACUGCAGAAUUUCCUUCUUUUUUAAAAAAUCUGAAUAGUAUCCCCUUGUAUGUAUAGCGUACAUUUUCUUUAUCCAUUCAUUAAUCAGUAGACAUUCAGGGUGUUUCCACAUCUUGAUUAUUGUGAAUACAACUGCAACGAACAUAGAAGUGCUCCUAUCAAUUUGAGAUACCGAUUUCAGUUCUUUUGGAUAAAAAACUCAGAAGUAGGAUUGCUGGAUCAUAUGGUAGUUCUAUUUUUAAUUUUUUGAGAGUCUCCAUACUGUUUUCCAUAAUGGCUGUGCUAUUGGCACUCUGGGUUCUUGUAAUCUCCCAGGAUAGAAAUAAAGAGAGAUCACUAGACAUAGCAGCAAAGAGAAAGAGAAAGAUUUAUUUCACUUGUGCACAAGGAAGUCAGCACUACAAAAAGAAAAGGGUGGGCUGCUCCCUGAGAGUAGUAUGUGCAUUAGUUUUAUAGGUCCUUUCUAUAGGGAAGGGUUUCAUCAGGUCCUGUAUAGCAGGGGUUUCUCUAGUGCUUGUUCAGUGGCCUUAUGCACUUCUUAAUACAUUGCAUGGAAGAUAUGCAGUUUAAAUCUCCACCCCUGGGUAUGAUUUUUAGCAUUAAAAUGAGGAAGGGGUAACUGUGAGUUGAAGUUCAAGUCUAUCUUCACAUGUGGAGUCCCAGGGAAGUCCCUAGCCCCCUAAAGCAGGAACCUGUAAUUAAUAGCUUCUUGGGUCUUUAUUUGAUGAUUAGCUAGAAGUUAGGUCAGCUAUAGCUUGAGUGAGAGGCAUUUUUUCUUUUUCUCUAAACCACAUCAAAAUCAGAAGCCUGCCAGCUUGCCUGUCUCAGCUGUACCUUUGCAUUUCCACCAAGAGUGUGCCAAUGUUCCCUUUUCUUCACAUCCUUGCCAACACUUGGCUUUUGAUUUUUUGGUAAUAACCAUCCUGACAGGUGUGAGAUGUUAUCUCAUUGUGGUCAUAAUUUGCAUUUCCUUGUAUGUUUUCUUGGGAGAAAUGUCUCCUUAAGUCCUUAGUCCAUUUUUAAUCAGUUUUUUGGAUAUUAACCCUUAUCAGGUAUAUGAUUUGCAAACAUUUUCUCCCAUUCUAUAGGUUGUCUUAUUAUUUUGUCAAUUGUUUCCUUUGUUGUGCAGAAGCUUUUUUAGUUUGACAUAGACCCAUUUAUUUUUGUUUUUGCUGACUGUACUUUUGGUGUCAUAUACAUGAAAUAAUUGCUAAGACCAAUAUCAAUAAGCUUUUCUAAUAUGUUUUAUUCUAGGAGUUUUAAAGCUUCAGUUCUUACAUUUAUGUCUAGAAGAAUUUUCUUUUUUUUCUCCCUCUCUUUUAAGAGACAGGGUCUCACUCUGUUAUACAGGAUGCAGUGCAGUGGCAUGAUCAUAGUUCACUGCAACCUUUAACUCCUGGUCCCAAAUCAUCCUCCGGGCCUCAGCCACUCUAGUACCUAGAGAUGCACCACCAUGCCUGGCUAGUUUUUAAUUUUUUGUAGAGAUAGAGUAUUGCUAUGUUUCCCUGGCUGUUCUUGAACUCCUAGCCUCAAGUAGUCCUCCCACCCAAGCCUCCCAAAGUGCUGAGAUUUCAGGUGGAGCCACUAUGCUGAGCUUGGAAGAUUUUAAAUUGUUAAAAUAUUCAUACUACCCAAAAUGAAAUACAGAUUUAAUGUAAUACCUAUCAAAAUUUCAAUGGAAGUUUGUACAGAAAUAGAAAAAAUAAUUCUGAAAGUCAUAUGAAACCAUGAAGGCCAUGAAUAGUCAAAUCACUAUUGAGAAAGAAUAAAGCUGGAGGCAACAUAUUUCCUGAUUUCAAAAUAUAUUACAAAUCUACAAUAAUCAAAACAGUAUGGUUCUGUUAUAAAGGCAGACAUAUAGCCCAAUGGAACAGAAUACAAAGCCCAAAAGUAAAUCUACACAUAUAUGGUCAACGUAUCUUUGAUAAGGAUGACAAGAAUACAUAAUAAGGAAGAAUUAUCUGUUCAACAAAUAGUGUUGAGAAAACUAGAAAUCCACAUGCAAAAAAAAAAAAAGAGAUUCGAUUCUUAGCUUACACUAUACAUCAAUAUUGACUCAAAAUGAAUGAGAAACUUAGACAUAAGACUUGACACUGUAAAAAUCAUAGGGUUUUCAGUUGGGAAGCUACAUAAUCUAAUUUACAUUUCAGAAUGAUCCCUUUGGUUACCCUAUGAACAAGAGAUUAUAAAGGGAUCAAGAGAAAGAAAGAGAGAGAGAGAGGAAGG